AGUUUCGCCUUUAGAACCACAAUUCUCUGAUAUGUGCAAUGAGAGAAUUAAUUAUAGACUCAAAGGAUUGCAUGCAGACACACACAGAUACAAACACAUACACACAACACACAGAGUUACACACAGACAUGCUCACAAUACACAGAAAUACACACAGACACACGCACACAGCACACAGAGAUACACACAGACACACACACACACACACACAGACAUACGCACAGAUGGGCACACACAGAGACACACUCACAGAGACACACAGAUACACACAGGCACACACACAGAGAGACAUACACACAGCCCACAGGGAUACACACAGACACACAGAGACAUACCUACAACACACAGAGAUACACACAGUCACACACAGAGAGACAUACAUACAAUACACAGAGAUACACACAGAGACACAGAUACAGACACAGACAGACAUACACACAGACACGGGCACACACAGAGACACACAGACACACACAGGCACACACGUGCAGAUAAGGUAAUAUUAGCUAGUUCAGGAGGAGAAAGAGAUAAAGAUAAAGUAAUAUUAGCUAGUUCAGGAGGAGUGAAAGAAGCCUUGUUUUUCUCCACUUUUUAUAGAAGAGAAAGUGAAGAUUCGAUUUGAGGUGAGUUCAGCACAAAAGCGUAUCCCAGGCCCUCUGGCUCCAACUGCAGCCCUUUCUACCUCAUUCCCAGACCCCACCUAAGCCUUUUCUCUUCAAAAUCUUCUCAGGCACACUGAUACACAUACCUCAGAUUUUUAAUUCUCCGGUUGUGUUCACCAGGUGCUUGGUCAUGAUUAAGAAUUCCGUGAUGUGUACCCCAUGUGUUUAAAUUUGCUGCUGAGUUAACUUUGUGGCGGCCUGUGGACUAGACCUCUGCACAUGCAAUGCAGAACGGCAGGGCCAGAUUUGAAAUCCUGCUAUCUUUUCGGCUGCCUUGUAAAAAUAACAUCAGGCGAUGGGGAUACGAUGCCAGAGGUCACCUGUGAUAAGUUCUGUUUAUGGCCAUUUUACUUCUAGGAAGACAGGAAGUGUCAGGAUCUCAGGGAUCUAGGAAGCCAAAAUGUUUUUCCACUCUGAAAUAAAGUGACUGACCAGGAGUUCCCGGCCACGCAGCCCUGUGGGAACUGCCGCACGGCCACUUUUAUGAAGUGGACACGUGUUGGUCCCACUGAAAAGAAACUCCCCACCCAUGGCUCCCUCACGCUGCAGCAGAGGCCCUGCCACAGCACCUGUCAGCCCCUGCCAGCUUGCAGGGGCGCAGGCGCAGAGCGGUUUGUGCCCUUGCUGGAGCCAGGGAAGGGCACAGGGUCCCUCCUGGAGUCAUGGGAGGUGCAGCCGAGGUUCUAUAUUAAAAUACAGAGGCUAGCACAUGUGCUUGGGGAAUGCAGCUACAGUAGUGGAAUGAAAGUGCUGUCCGUUCCUUACCCCCCCAGCUCCUCACCUGUCCUCCACACGCAUAUCCCUGGCUCCCUUUCCCUAGUAAGGAGACUGAAUUGAAAUUGUGGCUUGCCCGAGGCUGCAUACCUGUGCUCUUUCUGAAGCCCAAGUCACUGGCUCUAGAAUUCUAACCUGUGAGGAAGCCACUGAGGAUGUUUGUCAAAAUACAUAUUUCUGUGCCUUGCCCCAGUUCCACGGCCCAGGAAUCUGCAGUUUUCACAAGCACCCCCAGGUGAUUCUGGUGGUGUCUUUGCACUUCUUCAAGGCAGUACUGCCUGGAACGCAGAAUCCCAGCCUCCUCUAUCCUCCUUGCCUAAUGGCCUGGAUGCUCUCAGAUCUACAGGGGAAGGGAAGGUCACACAGUCAUCGCAAUAGUAACCUCAGCUGAUAAAUCCUCCCCCAUAAAACUUAUUCCCCAGUGUUUUUUAAUAGGAAACAAUAAAACUGUAACCAGCCCAAAUAUCCAUCAAAGAGAAAAUGGAGAAGUAAAUCAUCGCACAUUCACCUGGACCAGAUCUAUUGUAAAGCCAAUAAUACUGAAGCCCCUUCCAAGGCCCUGGGAGUCCUAACAGUGCACUGGCAGUGUCUAUAAUUUAUAUUAUGAAAUUUGCAUAAGGAAAACAUUUUGUCUCAUUUGUGCAAUUUCUCCUUCUAAAUAUACGUGUCACUUUGUACCUGAUUUCUAUAAGACCCAGGACCUACAAACCCUGUGUCUGCCCCUGCAGCCACCCAGGGAAGGACUGCACAGCAGCAAGACAGAUUGCCAUGGAGCAUGUUGUGCCCAACUAGGGACAGCGCAGAUAGAUUCUGUAAUUUGCCUAACAAUGUCUAUAGGAUGAUCCCAUUUGUCAAAAAAAAAAAAGAACUGGGCUUUAUUGAUGUCACCUAAAUGCACCUAAACUUCUUUUUUGCCCCAUGCUCUUCUGUACUCUUGAUCUUUCCCCAAAUUUUUAAAAACAUGACACUCAUUCCCUUAUUUUUCCUACUUAGAAAAGUGUAGAUGGUUUUAUCAUAGGAAGUUCAAAAAAAUUAAAAUAUAAUGAAAAAUACUCAAAUAGUGCCUCACAACAGUAACUACUGCUAACAUAAAUAAAAUCCAUAUUUCCUCUCAUACAGACCCCAGAGUUGCUUUGCCUGACAGUGUAGUUGAUGGAGAAAAUAAUCUUUAUCCUUAGCCUCCAUCUGGUUGCAGACCAUAAAGACAGGGAAAAAAUGAGGGUGUUGGUAGCUUCGUUAGAAACUGAAAGCUCACUGAUUUUUUCAAAACCUAAAUAGCCUGUGUUUCUCCAAAUAACUAAUUUGCAGCCUUCGGCAGCCAGGACUGGCAGGGAUGGGGCUAGGGGGACUGGGGAGAACUGCUCUCUCCUGAGGGUGGUCUGACCCGACAGCACGCAUGACCUUCCCACAGUCAGGAACUGCUCAGAGACGUGAUGGCAACUCCAUAGAAUGAAAUACUCUUCAGCCAGUAAAAUGUAUUUUUGGAUAAAUAUUUGCUUUAAAAAACUUUACUAUAUGUUGUUAAAUGAAAAAAAAACCUUAAGGCAUCAGAAAUUAUGUGCAGUAAAAUCUCACUUUUGUAAAUAAAUAUACCUGUUUACUACGUAUGCAUAAAAAGAAUCCUGAGAAAUAUAAGUACUGUAUGCAUAUUGUUGUUAAGUAUUUUUUCUGUUUGCUUAUCUAUAAUUCUAAUUUUGCUUCAAAGAACAAGUUACUCCGGCAAUAUAAAAAUAAAAUAACUAAUUUGUCUUGUCAUCAAACAGAUAGUAAGAACAGGCAAACCUGGCCCUCCACACUGCCAGCCUUUUGUGAUUCAAGGCUUCAGUUUCCUCCACUUGUUAAAAAGAUUCAACAAAGUAGUUGAAAUAGUAUGUGAACCAGUAAACCCUAAAAGGUGUCCAGUGUUGUCUGUGAGCUAAUUAAGUGAUUUGAUUCUGACUCCCCGAGUCUUCUGAUUUCGAAGCAGUGGGGAGUCAGACAGGAGCCUCAGGUGGCCUCUCCUGAGAGGCCCUGGAAAGUGAUGAGAACCUGGCCUCUGGCAGCUCUUCAUAAACGUCCAUGUUUUCCCUCUACUCUCUCACUCUUUUCCCAGGGCCUCAAACAGAAGAUGAAAAUCAAUUUCUAAAACAGCCCUCUGUGUGCUCUCUCGUAUCUCUCCUUUUCACACAUCGUGGUGGUGGCUUUCUCUGUGUUCCUCUGUUGAUUCAGUCUCUGGAAUUAACGGAUCAGGAUUCCAUGCCCAGAAUGCUACAAAGACUGUGCUUGAGUUCUCCCACAUCUCACUCAAUUACACAGAAGUUUCAGAUUAUGUAACAGAUGCUGUGCUGGGUUAGGCAGAGCCAUCUGACUUGUUUUGCUUUAUUUUAGACCAUGAGAUGGGUGAGUUUUUCUUUUUAAUGCCACAUUCUUUUAAGAAUUAAAAACCUCCACUUGGCUGUCAGCAUUGGAAAUCAGAGUGAUGGUGCAAGCCCUGAUGAGGACAAUGUCCUUGUCUAUGAAAAGGUGAAAUCAUUGCUUGAAAUCGCUAAGCAGGACAUGCAGUCCCAGAUGGAGGGGGGAAUUCGGGAGCUGGUUGGAAAAGAGUAUUUGGCACUUUGCAGCCUUGAGAGGUGCAGAAGAGACACCGAGGGGUUCACCACCAGAGCCACCAUUGUCAGAGAGGCGUCCAGCUGUGUCCACCUGGGACUCUGCCUUCAGGGCUUCUUGCCUGGCUGGGAGCUGCACAGGCAGACUCCUGGGACGGUGUGCCGACAGCUCUGGGCACCCCCUUCUAGGAUCUGAUUCCUGAGGAAUCACAAUGUGGAUUUCACAAUCACUUCCAGUGUCUUUUGCCAACCUCUGUGAACAGAUGUGCAAUUAAAAAAAAAAAAAGAAAGGGGCCCAAUUCUCAACACUGUAAGUGGAAACUUUUUAAUGGAAAAGGAUAGGCUAAUGAAUUGAAUUUGAAAUCUGAGACAGAACCGAUGCAUCAAAUGUGCUGGUGUUUACAGAUAAUACAAGGGGGGCUGCAUCUUAUGGUUUCAAUCCUUUUUUAAAUUUUUGUUCUGAGAGACCCAGCCAGCAGACUGCCGCCAGUCUUGUCAGAGAUGUCAGUGGUGGCCACUCUGAAUGGAAAGCAGCAUCUCUCAGCAUCUCUGAGGCACUGCUCCUCAGCGGAGACUGUGGUGGCUUUGCCUUUCAGCACGCAUCCUUUCUACGAUGCCUGACAGUGCCCAGGGAAUGGGCAGAGCUGGGAGCUCUGAAGCCCUUUCACCUAAACCACCCUGGGUCACCUGACCUAGUUUUCCUCCCAAUUUUAAUUAUGUCAGGCACUUCACAAAGGCCUCCUUGGGGACACCAUGAGCUCACUGUCAUCAGAUUGCUCCAAUCACAGCUGUGGCUUGCACACAACCGCCAUCUCUGCCCCAGCAGAUGCUGUGUGUAAACAGUUGUAUUAAUUACAUCUCAAAAACAUGGUUCUUGCCAGAUCCUCAGGAUUUGGGUGCAGCCUCUGAGGUGGGUGGGAGGCCCUCGAGGGAGAAAUGUCUGCAGGAAAUUCUUCCCCUACGAGAGGUCUGUUUUCUAAGUUAUCUAAGAGCUACUGCAGCUGUUUACUGCAGAGUGACCCUGCUCAAAGCUGUGGUCACCCAAGGCUUUGAAAGGGGACCUCCACUUCCGCCCUGGGUGGAGCACCGUGCUGGAGACCCACGCCUGCCAAGGCCUCAUUGUCAUCUCCACACGCCGUCCUUGGGGUGGGCCACUCCUGGGACACGCAGACAGGAAGCCGGCCACCUGAGCCACUCGGAGGCUCUAUCCAGAGUCAGCUGCCAAGCCUCACGUCACACAUCACUGUUAGUCUUGGAGGGCUGGCGGGGCCCUGAAGUCAAUUGAACACUUGGAUGACAGGGAACUUGCCACUGCCAGAGGCAAUAUGCUCCAUUUUUUUGACAGUUCCAACAAUUUUUCUUUAAACUGUCAUAAAAAAUUGCUGCUGUGAAUACCAGUGUCGGCGUCCCUGCCUCACCUUUACCUGGUGCUUUUCCACCACACAAAACUGUUUCUCCUCGUGCUGGCCUUGGGCUUGCAGACAGCUGAUUCUUCUCCUCCCGCGGCUGAGCAGCCUCCUCCGAGCAACCCUCUGACAACUCUGCUCCUUCUGACAACCUCUGCAAGGGCUGCCAGAUGUGAACAAGGGGCCCGGGCAGAAGGUAUCCAGGAAGACUGGAAACUCGAGGAAGCCUGCCCUGUCCUGUCCACCAGACUUUACGCUUGCGUCACUGGGCUUUGGGACCUAAGUCCUCGUCAUUUGUUCCUUUUGCAGUUCCUACUGUUCUCAGCACUUCCUUCCAGCUUACUGAGGUACACUCAGAUGUGAUAUGCCAUCGGUACAGACACAGUUCUGCUCCAGCAUUUCCCCGUGUUCUUUCUGUCGCUCUAUUUACUGAAUUACCGUGAGGAUGUGGAGCGAGGCUGAGUUCUGUAUUUUAACACCAUUUUAAUUCUCACCUACUGAGAAAUCCAUCCUCUUAUCACUGUGCUUUUUUUAACCUGUCACGAAUCCAUGAAAUCCUAUCAGCCAGCCUGCAUACUUCCUUUUAAGGUGCAGUUGAAUCAGGAGAAACUUGCCGCACAUGCUGCGUCCGGGCACAGCAUUGGCUGAGGCUGCUGCCCUGACCUGUCCGCUUUGUAGUACUGCCCAGCUAUGAAACAGGUUAGCCACACAUGACCUGCAUUUAGGAGUAACAAGUCUGUCUGUACAUGCACAUACAGCAACUUUUUUAAACUGUCUAUAUUUUUUCCUGAGAUAGGUAUUUAUAAUAUCUCCAUCUUCUUUCCCAUUUUGAAACUUAGAACAAGUUUGCCUGUCAACAGUUCUCCACAGCAUACUGUGUAUUCUAGGAUUUUCUAAGGUUGAGCAACGGAGGUUCAGCAAUUUUGACUUAAUUUCUUCCCAUCCCUUUUCCACGCAGCCCAGAAGCCUUGGAUCACGUGGUGAGGGGAAGAGGUUGUGCUAUGUCGGGAAACUCUGUAUCGAAGCUCGGCUCAGAUCAUGACAUUCUCUUGACUAAAACCCUCAGUUUCCAUCAAACUUGUCACUCUGGCAUUAAAGCCUGUCACUGUGUGGCUCUGAAAACCUCUCUGAACGUGUUCCCUGCCUCUGCCCUGCAGGUCCCUGUGCUCCACAGAAGCCCACUUAUGUGACCCACCCCCACUCAUCACCACCUUCCCUCACCCAGAGCCUCAGCUCCCCACUCCCACCUGUAAGACCCCUACUGGAAAGAUUCCCACCUGCCCCUCAAGAUUAAUCUCCAAGGACAUUUCCAAAUUCCUCUCCCCAUCUCUCAGCCAGAUGGCUUUGCUCCCUCCAGGAACCCCAGCCACCUUCGACCUCCAGCAGGGCACUCCACUCCACAUUCUCCUGGUCUGUCUGGCUCAUCUUACCUGAGCCAUGCUCUCCAGGUGAAGGACUAUGUCUAACUCAACUCUGCUUUAAAAGCAGCUAACACAUUGCUCUUUGCAUAUUGUUCACUCACUAAGUUGAACUGGACUUGGACAUGCACACUGAACUGCAGCGUCUGCUGCUUCUUGGUGGCCCAGCUCGUCAAAAGAAUAAGAUUUCAGCAAAACAAUGUAACAAUUUUUUUUACCAAAAGUAAUGUUAACAAUAUAUGGUUUUCCCCUGAUGUUUGCGUCAAAAUGCUUUUUGGAAAAAACAUUUUUCAACUCUUUAGGGUCAGAAUUAAGCAAUGAAAUUUAUAUACCACAUGUAUAAUGUGUAUGUUUAUCUAAGUAUCUGUUCAUUUAUAUAUCUUAAAUAGAAAUUUUAAAAAUUUUUUUAAAACUCCUGAUAAACAUUCUCAGGAGGCACACUAUGUAACUGUUGGUUGAUAUACCUAGCUAGAUGGUGAAAUCAGAUUUUGUUUAAAGCAUGGAGGAGAGGGAAAAAUUAAAUCUUGCAGAUUCUGCAGUCCUUAACAUCUUUGAAAGAGGAACAUUUCAGACAAUGUAAUAAGAAGGCCACGUGCUUUGACUUCUGUAGAUUUUAAAAAUACUUCUGUAUAGUUUCUUCUUCCUUUGAAGAAGUUUGGGGAGUUUGGGAAGAUGGAGAAAGAUAUAAGAAUAGACUCCCCAUAUGGGUCAUGAAUUAUCUUUUUGCAUCAGAACUCUUAGUGCAGUUUCAGUAUUUUCUUCCUCAGGAGGGUGAGCUGCUUCCGAAUGUCCUCCCCUUCUUUGAGGCAUCCUCUGUUGGUGAACUUUGAGAGCAUCCAUUUAUGAAGUUGAUGACCUUUCCCAGUCUCUGCAAGCCCUUCAGUGUGUGUCCUCUCUGAGCAAAUCUGAAUUGUGUGCUUAAUACAUGGAAAGGGAUUUGGGAGGGUUGCUUUUUAAACUGAUUUCUUAAUUAAUAUUAUGGUUUAGUUAACUAGACAGUCUCAUUGCAGAAGUGCAUAACCAUAAUAUGUCUUCAAAUAUAUCUCCCUUCCUAACACCCUGUAAUAUACUUUUGUAAAGAUACCCUUACAGAAUGUGAUCCACCAUUUAUGAACCUGCAGCAUUGCAUUCAGAGACUAAGUGAAAAGCUGGCAGAUUUUCAUUUAAAGCACAAGCUAAGGAAGAAAGCUGGUCUAGAAGGAGCUACAGAAGGGUAAUGCUUAGGGAGGGAAUGAUGUGCCUGUGGGUGGUGGUAGUUAAAUCUAACCAAAGAAUGAUGUCGUGGGUGUUUGGAUAUUGGAUGGUCCACAUUGGGCCACAUUCUUUCAAACAUAAGAGUCUGUAGAAAUAUGACCUGUAAAAGACUCUUAAAUAUUCUGGAAACUGUUUCUUCCUUGUCACAUCCUUAUAUAUACUUGAACCUAUGCCUACCAGACAUGACAUGUGACUAUUCAUACAGAUUUCAUCAUCUCUGGUUUAAGAAUAAAGGAUGCUGCAUAGAAGGCUCACAUCUUUUAAUUCACAAGACUGAAACUGUUCUGAAAUGACAUUGUUUCUAAAAAUUCAUUACUUGCAUUAUAUUCAUUUUUAUUUUUCCAUGCCAGAAGGGUAGAAGUUCCUGUGCUCAUAUUAAGAAACAGCAAUGUCAAUCGAGGCCCAACUCAAAUCCAAUUUAUAGGAGUUAUAAAGGGCGUGUGCCUGUUUUGUCUAGAAGCAGUGUUGGGCAGCACUGAGUAGGAUAGACCACCUGUUGCUACCGAUAAAGGAGCAGCUUCUCGAAUGCUCCUGUCUGGUAGGCACUAUCCCGAGUGCUUUGGCCCCUCAUCCACAAUCUGUGUGGCAAAAGGCAUUGCAGGCAAUUCAGUGAGGAGACCGAGGCAUGGAGAGCAAGUGCCAUGGAAUUCCCUAAGGCCGUGCAGGGAGCAGGUUGCCAAGCUGGGUUGAAACCGUCCUCCGUAGGCUCCCAACUCCGCCGUCGCUGCUACUGUGCUGGAUGAUGCCUGGUAGAUGCAGAUGUGGAGCCCCAUGGAUUCUGAGACAGGCCGGGUUUCAGUCCUGCCCUAGCUGCCUAUUGGCUGGAUGACCUUGGCAAGUUGACUUUCGUGAGCCUCAUUUGUCUCAUCUCUCAAUUAAGAAAACCUAGAGCCUAUCUGUGGGGGUUAUCUGAAGGAUUCCAGGGAUGCAUAUGGCACUGUCUACCGCAUGCGGUAACUGUUUCACAAAUGAUGAGGAGCGAUUUAUGUUCUUAGUGGAAAUAUGUCGGCGUGUGAAGUCCCAAAGCUCUGCCCUGCCUGGCUUGAUCCAGUGCCUAGGCACUGCCCCUCUUCCCCUCUCUCCCAACCCACUGUAAGAGGCUAGGCUGCCUCAGUAACUCUGAGGGGCAUUGACUCUUUUCAUCCAAAAAUUCAUGUUACUGCCCCACAUUUUUUCUGUUGUUUUACAACGCAGUAGGAAGUGGGCAGACUGUCAGGAAAAGUGAUUUAUAGUCAUGUAUUGCUUGUGCUUUGGCUUCAUUUGAUCCAAUGCAGAUCAGCUGCACUCAGAAAACUACUCAAGUGAAAGAGAAAAAGUAACUGAAGGGGGAAAUCUGGAUGAGUAAGAAUUCCAGGGAUAGGAAUAUUAAUAGCAAGCUUUUUGCCUGAUAUAGUCACUUUAUGCUGCAGGGGUGCCCCUUUAUAAAGUGCUUGUACAAUGGAUGUUUGCUUUUGAUUUUGGAUUUGGAGUCUAAUGAAUGUUCUAAAUUAUUAUUAGAGGAGCUUGCGGUUGUUACAUGUCUGCCUUUAUUGCUUAUUUUUAGCCAUCUCCCCUGAUGUCAAAUGCUCAGGCAAGAAUGAUACAUUCAUUUAUAAUGUGGCUCCUUCAGAAAUAUACCACAUACCUUUUGGUGUGGUUUGUGGCUGAGAAGAGUGGGGAAUGCACAAGUGGAAAACUGCAGAAAGAUUAUGCCUUCAUCACUUCAAGUAUUUGAGAUGAAACUAGAUCAUUUGCUGUUGCUUUUUAUUCUCAUUCUAAGUGCUUUUCAAAGUCAGCGCUAAGAUUUUAAAAUGGUUUUCUGUUGUUGGCAGAGAGGGAAUUACUCUAUUACUUUCUGAUAAAACAGAGUCUUUCAUGAUCAAAGAGAACCAGGCUCUAGUAGUUCCAGUAUCCUAACGUGGACACUAAUUGUUUCCCUCCUUUUCUUCAUGAAAACAGCUUCUGCACAAAUGAUAGCCUUGUGAACUAGCCAUGGGCACAACUGGAGAAGCAUUUAGGGAGCUUUAGUGCAAAUUGAGACCACCUACACAUCUGACUCUACAGGGUUUGACAACAUCCAGGGUGAAUCACAAAACAUCAGUCUAAUCAGGGCUUAUAUAGAAAGAGUGAAAGAACUCUGAUUUCAUCCUAAAGAUUAUUUAUAUUAACCAUUGUUCCAAAUGCAUUAACUAUUUUAAUUUAGUUGUUUUGAUUGUUAAAAAAAACACAUCUGUUUGGUAGAUAAGACAUAAUUUAAGACAAAUGUUCUAUUUGAUAAGCUUUUAGAAACAACUUAUUUUUAUUCUUUCCUGUGAGAUAACUCAGAUGUGGAGAAUGUGACAAAAUUUUAAGCAUAACAUGAGAAGGGCUGACACACAUAGAUUUCUGUGUGCUUACUUGAAAACAACAAAAUUUAAGAAUUUGGUAUAGGAGUUGUAUCAGGUAGUGCAGAGUCCCCAGGAGACCUAGAGACCCAGGUCUGGGAGCCUAGCGGCAAGGGCUGAAUGUGGGAUGACAUCAGCAGAAACUCACAGCCACUGCUAUUCCAAAAACCCAGCAGCAGCUCAGUGCAGGGCAGUGCUGAUAGUACAGUGCCUGCAAUCCUGGAGUGGAUUUGGAUGUGUCAGGUACGCACACGCUCACUGCUCCCCCAGCAGUACGUUGAACAGUGUGCGUCCAGGUGUCUGUAGGGCCCCUCGCCCUAACUCACAAAACCAUUCUGGGUCAGAAGCCACCAAUAUUGUCAUCAUCCUCCCUUUUCUGAGAACCCUAGUAAGUCCCUCCAGUGGGGCAAGCCCACCUUUUCCCUUCAUUCUGUGGCAAUAUGCCUUCAUUUCCUAAUCAGUUUUGCCCUGCUCAUUCAAUGCAAAAUGGAUCUGCUUUCCUUGGGCACCAAUAUGUCCAGGGAUUGUUUAUCAAUCUUCAGUUCUGUUUCCUUUACAUAUCCCUCCAAAAAUCAGGCCUGCACUGCCUGUGCACUCCACAAUCCACAGGCCUGAAGGAAAUGUUAUCUUUGAUGUAGAGACUUAAAGUAAAACUCUUCAAAUUAAUUAUUUCAUGCAAAAGGCUAGUCCUGACUCUAAUUCUAAGACAUGUCUCCUAAACUCUGGAAGUCUGAUGUAUCCUAUUAUCAACAUUUAUCCUUAAUGUGAUGGUUUAUCAUUUAUCCUCAAAGCUGCAUUGUAAAAUGUACACUGUAAAGUGUACAUUUUAAAGUCGGUUUUAAAAAAUCAUAUUUAGAGAUCCUGGUAAAAAUCUAUCAAGUCAAGACAUUACCUUAUUACCCAUGGAAUUGUCUUCAACUCUUACAGUUCAAAUAUUCCUGAAUUGGCUUUCACAAUAAACAUCCUAAAUAUGUAAGUAGAAACAUAUAUAUUGCCAACUUUGUGCCUUCCCAAGCAAAAUUAAAAUACAGGAAAAGUCAGUUUGUUUUGCCCAUAAAUAAAUAUAUGUGUGUGUGUAUGUGUGUGUAUACACAUACACACUCAGAAAAGAUAGAAGCAGCAGCAUAUUUUGGCAGCAUCUGGUUUAUUGGAACUCAAACGUUCUGAUUGUGCAUACAGACUAGUUAAUGUGGUAACAAUUAUGUAUUUCUUCCCUGCUCCUUGCCUUCUUUCCCUCCCCAGUUUUUUUCUUCCUGAUAGUAGGUGUGUACUUUUUUCCUAUUUCCAUUGGCAAGCCACAUGACAAGCAAAACGAUCACUCGAAGAAUAUUGUUCCCUCAAUCAAGAAAAAUGCCCAUUGGGUUUUGUUAUUUGAUGUUAUUUGAUGACAGAGACCUAUUGUUUUUCCAUUUUUCUUUUUUUGUUUUCCGUGGCACCUAUGGAAUUAAGCAAUAUAAAAAAUCUAUUAUUUCAGAUGUUCACGUCUAAUGAAUUUCAUGUGAAAUACUGGCAGUAUAACCCCAAAUAGAGGAAAUUUGUGAAGAGUGGAUGCUGCAGGGCAUGAGACAUCUGCACAGAGUUCAUCUCUUCCAGCAUCUUGCAUGUCCCAAGCACUGCCCUGCCAGGCAGAGAAUGCUGCAGAUCACGGCAGUGAAUUCCAGUUGUUCAGAGCACAUUUGACUUCCAAAUUCUCAAGGCCACAGAUUUGAGGACAGAACAAUAUUUGCAUUUGAAAUUGGAAGAUUAUUUUUUGCACAAGUGCCUAUAUGCUAUAUAGAGUUUGCCCACUCUGCAUUAUCUUCCCCCUGUUCCCCCGUUAUCUGGCACAAGCUAUUCAAAAGACACGCCUACUUGUAAAAUAAAUGGUUUGCAAACUAAGGAAAAUACUUAAAUCUCAUGUAAAUGGUACUAUACUAUGUAUAAAAAUGUGAAGAAACACAGAACAGCUCAUGAACACCUCCACUGCUGUAUAAAAGAACCAUCUUUUUUCUGGCUCCUAUUGGAUGCCUUAGAAAAAUCUGUAUUUCCUCUUUAGUUAUUGUGUUUGAAAGAUGAAGUUGAGACAAAAGUUCUAUUCUUUUUAAGUUGGCAGAACUUCUGAAAGGUGAUUUUUAGCUGCAGUGUGACUCAUUCCAAAUGCAGAAAUCUCUGACCCUGAGUUAGUCUAUUUGUCAUGCAAGAGCCUAGAAAAGCCCUGAGUGAUAAGAAAUGGCCAUAGGCCAUUCCCACAGAAUUUUCAACAAAAAUAGAAUCAUGCUUAUGUUCUAGUCAUGACUUAGAACUUAUAACUCAUGUUCGGAACUGUCCAUGUUCACGCACAGGGGCCGUAUCACUCCGCCAGAGCUGCCCUGGGUGCCGGUGUGCAGAGGGGUCCGAGAGUGACUGUCUCUUCCUCUGUUGUCGAAUGUGUGGGUUAUCUCCAUAAAUGGCUGCCAUGAGCAUCCUUGUUCACACAUUUUUAGGUACUUGAGUGAGUGUCUGUGGAAUAAUUUUGGGAAGUGAAAUCUGUGGUCAGAGGUUUGUGAGUUUUACAUGCUACAUUUUCAGAAGUUGAGAAAUAGCAGUAGGCUGAAGGCAAGUCGCCAUGCCUGGAAUUCAUGAACACUAGUUGAAAGAACUGGCGUGAGUUAGUCAUGACAGGAGAGAUGGGGAAGGGAGUUGCAGGUAGGAGGGCCAUCUUCAAAUUCUCAAAGUAUAGUCACUCCAAACCAAAAUUCGAUUUAAUCUGUAGGACUCCAUUCUCAAAGCACAGUCACUCCAAACCGAAAUUCGAUUUAAUCUGUAGGACUCCAGGUGGCAGAAUAAGAGGCAAUGGAUGGGUGGAAGCGAAACAGGGCCAAAGUUUGACUUCAUGUGCAACUUCCUAAGGAGUGAUUUGAACUCCACAAACAUGAACUAAGCACCUCAACACAGGCUGGGCAAGUUGCUGUUCUUUUGGAGCUUACAUCUUAGUGGGGAAAGAGAAAUGCCUAUGUAAACAUAUAAAUCAGCAGGAUACAUUGUGAGGACGGUCAUUGCUCAGUGAGACUGCAAUAGAGUGAUACGCUGGAGGGGGCUGCAAGGGAGAAGGUGGGAGGGACAGCAUUUAGCAGAAUGAGCAGCACAGUCCCAUAGGAAGAAGAAUUUAUUGCCUCCUUAGGCAAAUAAAUUCCCAAACCUUGAACAUCAGAAAGGAAAUAGAUUAAUGUGCACAGAGGAUUAAAUUAUGUGAUCUGCAAAGUCAUUUAAAAUCUAUUUCCACAUAAAACAUAUUAAUGCAACCUAAACAAAAGGGGUCUGGAUACCCUCAUCUUCUUCCCAAGCAUCAAGUCUUUCUAUAGUUAAACUGAGAUGCUUUUAUUCUUGGAAAAUUUUAAGGACUAUCUACAGCAAUGGAAGAAUCGGGUGUUGGGAUGUGUUCCCAGGUAAUAAUGACUGCAGGCUGAUUUGGCCCUUGAGGUGUGGCCUCAUGGCCCUCUCCAAAAAAAAUCAAGGACCUGCUACAAAGCACAAAGCCGACUGCAAUGCUUGCUGCUUACUGGUUAGGGCAGCUCCUCUUUGCCAGCGACCAAGCAGAAAGCAAGACAAGACAGGUUCUGAAGCAGUAAUUCAAAGCCUUCCUCGCUUUCCCAUGUGAGUCAUUGCUAGUCAGAAUAUUACCUUUGCAGAGAGGCUUAAUUCCAAAUUUGCUCUUAAAGGGAUAUCCUCUCCUGGUUUAGGUAUAAACUUUUGACUCACAGGACAAAUUCUAUCAUUCCUUUGGGCCUAGGAUUGCAUUUAUUUCCAUGACAAAAGGGCCUGUCUGGUGUUUCAGCAAAUGAAAACAAAAAUAUAAAGCCCAUCUCCUUUUGAAUGAGCUCUAAAACAGUUCUCCACUGGACUUCAGAACAAGAGGGAGCUCUGGGCUGCUGGCUGGUUGUGCAUUUGCUGUGGGUUCCCUCCGGCAGGCGACCUCUCCGCGCUGAGAAGGUUAUCCGGAUAACCAAGUAAGAAAGUACAUGAGGAGGCACAGAAAGAAAAAUGUGAGAGAUAACAGCAUAAACACACAGUGUAUGUUGUUAUGAGGCAUCACAUGAUGAGAUACUGCUGGGGAGGGAAGAAGUGAGGAGAUUCCUAGGAAUCUUAUGAGAAUUUCCAGAGACAACAAGUUUUGAGCUUUUUUUUAAUUUAGAAAAUUUACCUUAUUUUUAAAAGAAUAUGUAACAUAUCCCAUGCUAUAAAAUUCUAGACAUAGUAGAUUUAAAACAGCAUAAUGGAAAAUAUAAAUAUCUAUUUUCUUUUCCUAUUUAUGUAUUCUGUGCCAGUAGGAAUGUAGCCAAAAAGAGAGAAAAGGGGUCUCUGCAGACAUGGAUGUCUCUGUGACUUGAUCACUGCUAACCCAAGAAGAUAAUAAAGCAGAAGCAUGUAUCCAGGUUGCUGCAGCCAAGCCUGCCCGGUCUGCGGGGCGUCCUCACACAUGGGGCAGCUCUCCCACCCCACACACUGGGAAAGGCGGACAGAGGCUGGGCAAAGCCCCCAAUUUUCGUUGGCACUGACCCCGAUGAUUUAUAGGCCUUUGUUUCCCAUGUUAAAUGUCUUACGAUCAUUAAAUUAUUUAUAGCUCAAUUAGCAUGUGUCCAAAACCAGGAAGUUCAUAGGAGACUGUGUGACUGGGAAUUAAGGAGCAAAGCAACUUUCCAGUCUGUGAUUUACUGGGUUUCCAUUCUGUUUCCUGUUCGGAUCCGGAAGUAGAAUUUCAAAUAUUGCUUUUCAUGCUUUAUUUGGGACCGAUUUUAGCCCCGCUCUCCUUUCUCUUGCCAUUCGCUGGCCAUUAGCCACCAGCCUCUGCACAAUGACCAGCUGGCCCCUGGCAGAUCUUGGGCCCAGGUGUGAAGUCGCUGGAGAAGCAUUUCAGGGCCAAGAUGGGAGUGAUUUCAUUUUCCAUUGACACUAUGCAGAAAUGAAGGGGAUUCAAGUGCCUUCAGAAAAGCUUCCUUCCAGCGAAUGGAGUUUUGGGGGUUUUCCAGACUUGCAACUGCUUUUAUUCUUGGAAGCAUCAUUGUUGCUUUUUCCCCCCUUCCAUUUAUAUCCCAGGAACUGAUUCAGAAACCAUAGAAAUUGGAUUUGGAAUCGCUGAAUGCUAGCAGACAGCUGACUGCACUCUUCCCAAGAAACCCUGCCAGCUGGGUUCGGGUAUCGCGCGGUGUGUGCUCUCUCUGCCUGGCCCGCUGAGUCCUCUAACUCUAAUGGAUUCCUUCUUACACCAAAGUGCACUAGAACUAAAGUGUUUUGCUUCAUUCUUUAGACAUUUUGUGGUUUAGGGCUCAAUCAGCCAGGGUAUGAUUUGCAAUCCACAGUAACCGGUUUCAGAGCAGCUGCCCAGCGAGGCAGGUUUCAUCUCGCUUGCUAGACGUUUUGUUUUUUUUUUUUUCUAAACCUCACACCUUUUAUUUAUUAGACUUGGAUUCCAGUUUCCUGAGCCUGUUUGUGCCACUGAUUAGACAGGCUUGAAGCAGAACCCACCAGGCUUCCUGAAUAAAAUGCAGCAGUGAUUGUAUUAGGGGGUUUUAAAUUGCUCAAAAUACUGUCUAAAAAACACUAAAAAUCAUGUUACUUUCUAGAUUGAAUAAAAUCCUAUAGAAAUGAAUUCCUGGACUUGAUAUGUAGCAAGCUGGCAUUGGCUCGGGAGUGAGUGGGCUCAGUUAAGUGAGCUAAGAUGAGAUGGUGCACAGGCGAGCACCCACCUGAGGAGUGUUUGGAUGUUAUGAUAGCCAGCUCCUCUGUAAAGACCUGUCCUUCUAUGUCAGCAGCCCAGCAGAUAAAUGACGUGUAAAUACCACAUUUAGGAGGGCUUAUGAUGAUGCCAAUUAAUGGAGACCUUUUUGAAACAGGAAGGAGGUGAAACAUAUUCCUUUGCUUCUACAUCACUGUGUGCCAGGCACUGUUUACAGCAUCUCGUUUAACCAGCAGUCACCACCUGACGGAUGGCUGAUGUGGGGUGGGGUCCCAGGGUGGGAUUGCGUGAUGGGCUUGGGGUCUCUGGCUGAUGGGUGCCAGAGCUGGGACUGGAACUCCUGGCGUGACUGAGGCAGACACCUGGGCUACCCAGCCUCACCCACGACGCCCUCACUAAGUGACCCACAGGACUCACCGGAAGCAGGGCAGCAAGGUCCCCCUACAGAGGUCCCCACUGCAAACCGAUACCCAGCUUAGACAGCAGUUCUGCAGUCGGCGUCUCACCCCUUCGGGUCUCAUUGUGACUCACUUUGAUAGCCACACGAUUUAAGGGUGGUUCAGUAGUGAUUUGAUGAGUGCUGUGGCUCAGGGUCAUUCCCCUGCCCAAGCAUUUCAAAUUCCAGAAGUUCAUGCCCUGCAUGGUGGGUGAAAAGUCUCAGGCCAACCAUGAGCACACAGCAGCCAGGCGACUGAGGCAGCUGCCCGGGGUGGCACGUUGCUCAAACCCAUCAUUUGGAGUCAAAACAAACAGAUGAUUAGCUGGGGUGGUCACUUUCAAUCAAGAGUUUUCACAUCGCCUAGACAUGGCCUCAGAAUCAGGCCUGGUGUGGCCAGGGGCUGAUCUCACAGUAGACAGGAAGUGUGGCCCGAGGGCCAUGGCUGCCCCCUCAGAAGGCCCUGUGGAGUGGCUGGCCGAGCCUCAGCAGCCUCCUGUGAAGCGAGGAAGGGUCUUCCUGCCGGCCUCUGGAGAUCAGUAUGGGAAUGCACAAGUAGGAAACGCUGGAUGGGAAUCCCUCUGCCCUGUGAUACCAAGGCAGUGAGUUUGUAGACUAUGGAAUUGCUGUCGGAGGGCUCUGUAACCGGCCAAGGUCACACAGGUAGCCAUUGGUAGAGCAGGGACUGGAAUCCCAGACCCCCAACUUCCAGGACUGUGCACCUUUCUUUAUCCCAUACAGCCUUACAGUCAAGUGCCAGUGCAACACCUGAUUCCCAGGUUCCAGCCUUUGUCUUUUAUAAUGGGAAUCAACCUUAUCUUGACGAUCCAGAGAUAGUCAUCAAGGAAGAUUAAAUUAUCCCCUUAGACUCAGAGUGACCAUAUCAUUUUCCCUCCACACAAGGACACUUUUGAGAAUGAAAAGGAGGAGAUGUCUGUACCAGACGCUGGAUGACAGGCACCGACAGGCUGUCUGCCAGGGGAGCAGCGAUUCCUGUAUGUUGUAGAAAGUUUUUCAAAAGUCACCUUGGAAAGAGGUUUUGUUCCUUAACCUUCUGUUAAAUAGGAAGCUCCGUGAAUGAAAACAACUCCCUUCCCUAAACAUUCUAGUAAUGACCCAACACUGCCAAGCCUGCCAGCUCUGCCUCAUGGUCGUGUUGACUGUGUGAGACUAUGUGAGUGCCUGCUACACAGUACGCUUUCAGUAAACAUGGUAUUGCCUCGAUAAUCCCACAAAAAUGUCCUAUUCAAAUCACCUGGCACCCAGGAAAUUUCCUUCUUUUUUUUCCCAGGUGAAAUAUACAGUUGAAAACACCUGACAGCAAUUCCCCUCUCCCAUGUGUUUGCAGGAUGGUGGUUUUGGUUCCUCCAUCUUUGAUGUGUACAAGUGUGAUGUUUUCCCCCCACAGACAAGUAAACCACAUUCUCUUCACAUUCCCAAUGUUUUGUCAAUGUACCUCCUUCAAUAGAGGAUCGAUAAGGAAAAAAAUCAUUGACAAUCUCAAUUAGAUUCACUAUUUCAUCCAAAAGCAUAGCUUAGAACUCUAGUUUUUGUUCAACACUCUUGCCCUAUGAGUGCACAGAACUUUAAUUCUGAUACAAACAUCCCUGAAUGUUUAGCUUUGACAGAGAUUCCAAGGUGAUUUGAUAAGAAGCAGGGCUGUGUUUGGGCUCUGGGAGUUUUUGAUAUGGUUUCAAGCCCCAUCCAAAACCCACAGACCUCUAGAAAGUAGGUGCCUGCCUUCCUGCAGCAGCCCUGGAGCCUGCUGGGGGCUUUGAGCAGCUGCUGCCAAGCCAGGCCUCACCCGACACUCUGAUGGGCACGGCCAUGGUGGCAGGGGCUUGGACGCUGCCAGGUGACUCUAACUUGUGGCCAGGGUGGGAAGCACUGCUCCACAGAGGUGCCAAAACCAGGUUCCUUCCUGUGUUCUCACAUUUCACAGCCUCAAUGUAAAAAGUAAGACAUGGGCACUCUGGAAUAUUACAAAAAUAUAGAAAAGCAUGUUAUAGUAAAUAAAAGGCUCACAGAAUUUUGUCAUUUAGGAACAAUGAUUAUUAAUAUAUUAGUGUGUGUUUUUGCUCAUUAACAGUAUAUCCUGAGAUAUUUCCUAUACCAUUUAAUAUUUUAAAAGAUGUUUACACUGGCCACAGUAGCUCAUACCUAUAAUCCCAACACUUUAGAGGGCAAGGCAGGAGGAUCACUUGAGGCUUAAAAAUUAGCCAGGUGUAGUGGCACAUGCCUGUAGUCCCAGCUACUCAGGAAGCUGAGGCUGGAGGAUCACUUGAGCCCAGGAGUUCAAGGCUGCAGUGAGCUAUAAUUGCACCAUUGCACUCCAGCCUAGGUGACACAGUGAGACCCUGUUUCUAAAAUAAAUAAUAAAUAAAUUAAAACAUUUAAAAAUACAUGAUGUUUAAUUAUUAGAGGACUCAAUUUUAUAUCUAUGUAUACAAUAAUUUUUAAGUUUCUUAAUAUUGGACUUUUAGUACCUUUUUAAAAAUACUAUUUUUAAAAAAAUCUGUAUUUCUAACUUUUUAUAACAAGGAACCUUUGGCUUUGAGAUGACUGGGGAAUCCAUUCUUUCCUAUAGUAUCCAUGUCCAAUGGACUUAAAGUAUUAAUCAAUGUGUUUAUGUUUUGUUAUUUUUCUGGCAUUACAAAAAAUUCUAAAUAUAUUGUUACCGCCUGUAUAAAUAUCAGCUUUUGAGAGAAGGACAUUGUGUAGAAAUAAUGAAACACUGCAACUUGUAUUUGUAUUAUUCUUUUUUUUUUUUUUUUUUUUGAGAUGGAGUCUCGCCCUGUCACCCAGGCUGGAGUGCAAUGGUGCGAUCUCUGCUCACUGCAAGCUCCGCCUCCCAGGUUCACACCAUUCUCCUGCCUCAGCCUCCUGAGUAGCUGGGACUACAGGUGCCCGCCACCGCGCCGGGCUAAUUUUUUGUAUUUUUAGUAGAGACGGGGUUUCACCAUGGUCUCGAUCUCCUGACCUCAUGAUCUGCCCGCCUCAGCCUCCCAAUGCACUGGGAUUACAGGCAUUAUAUUAUUCUUUAAAUUCACAUGAGAAUUUAGUAUGGCUUCAAAAAAUACCAUAAGUUAAAAUAUCACCAAGACUCUGUUCAGACAAAAGUAUCAGAAAAGUGAGCCAGGCACUCACAUAGUUUAUAGUUUAUAAAAGUGAGACAGGCAUGAUCUCUUAACCUCACUAUAGUCCUGUGAAUAAGGUUUAUUUACAUUUCAUUUUACCUGCCAGGAUUAUUGUAAAAACGCCAAGCACAUUGCCUACACAAACUAAAUAUUCAGUCAAUGGCUGCUAUUUUCAUGAGUUCGUUUUAACAUAUAUUUAUUGUCCUCUACUGGAUUUAAGAAGUUAUAUUUAUUAUCAUCUAAGAUUUUAGCUAUUCCUUCUCUUAAAAAUAGAUUUUAUAAUCAAUGGCAGUAAGGGAGAGUAACUCGCAGUUCUCUGAAUCUCAAGGGGUUCCUGGAAGCCUUCCUGAAGGUAUAGUGAAAUUUCAGCUUCACAUUCCCAUCCAUGAGCUCCCUGCAAAUAUCCCGGUCUGCUCUCAGGACCCAGUGACUUACCUAUGCAGAGGCUGUAGAUAGCACCUGGAGCUUCCUGUGUGCCCUCCUCAAACUCAGCCAAUGCCGUCAUACAGUAGCAGGCAGGUGUCUUUGCUGGGUAGUUGGACUGGAUGUCCCUGGGAUUGCAGAACUGGAAUGGGGAGUGACAUCAGGAAACUAUAAUCAUCAGGACAACAUGGUUUGCCAUAACUUUAAGUUUUAAGCGACCGCAGAUUAUGCGGAGAGAGAUGCAUGCCCACAGCCAUGCUUCCCAUGUAACUGGAGAGGGGUCUGAAGUUUGAAACAAGUGUUCCUAGGCACGGGUUACAGUGUUUGUUAUCAUCAUACUUGAUUUAGAAUGGGGCACAACAUGUGGAUUCAUGGUAACUGUUACAACCUUACUCAUUUUAAUACCUGAAAACAUGCUUUCCCCAUGCUGGGAAUCGAAAGAUUCUCCUAGGAAAAGAAAGGCUUGACAACAUCGAUUCAAAAAGGGCAUGCAUUUUCCUCAUUUAAAUAACUCUAAUGUGCAAGUAGAUCCCCUGACCUCAAGCUCAGAAGAGUCCAGGCCUUCACACCUUCUCUGCUUCUGCUCUGGGGCCAGCUAUUGAGAUUCCUGUGCCCACGCAAUGCGCACAUCCCACCCCUGGCCGCUGUCCACAAGAAAUCCAGUUGCACCAAGCACCCCACUUUUUGCACCUCUCAUUUAUGUACUCCUAAGAGCCUCACCACAACUCCCUUCUAAAAACAUGAGUUCCUGACUGGGAAUUCGAUGCUGCCCAGGCAGCUUUGCUCAGAGGGAGCAGCCUUCUAGAAAUGUUUCAAGUAAACUUUCAAGUAUAACUAAAUUCAAAAAAAACACAUACACACACACACACACACACAAGUCAAAGGUGUGUAAUUUGGCCAAUAUCACAAACCAAUUAGCCCUUUGUAAGUGGCACCCAGAUCAGGACAGCUGACCAUACCAGCACCCUAGAAGCACCCCGUGCUGCCUCCUGGGACAGGGCUACCACCAUCCUAAGGCCAGCACGAUGGGCCAGCUUUGCCUGCUGUUGAAUUUUGCUUACAUAGAAUCCUCCAGUAGGUACUCCUUUGGGUCAGGUUCUUUCACUCAACAUUAUGUGUUGAUAUUUUUCCAUGCUGUGCUGCAAAAUUGUAUUUCUUGCAUUCCAUAACUGGGCAGUUCCAUCAUAGGAGAAUACCACACUGCGUUCGUCCAUUCUACCGCCAAUGGACAUAUGGGUUCUUUCUCUUUUCUUGCAGUUACAAGUUUAUGAAUAUUGUCCCACGUGUCCCUGGUGAACUUUUGUUUGCAUUUCUGUUGGGUACCUCAGAGUGGCGUUGCUGGGUCAGAGGGUACUGGUCGCUUUAGUAGCUUUGAAAGAUAUUGCCAAAACAUUUUCCAGCGCAGUUAUAGCAAAUUAUACACCACCAGCAGUAGAAAACAUCUCCUAAUUGCUCACAGUAAACCCCCAAAGAUUGCCACAUACAUCUUCCAUAUCAAUUACUUAACUAUUCAGCAAAUUUGAAGGGAAAUAUAUUUAAUCUUUUUAUUCAAAUAGUUUAUAAAGUGGAAUAGAGAUGUGGGUAAAAGUUGUCUUGCCACCUUUUUAGAUCGGUAAAAGUUUGUUGAAUGCAGGCAAGAAAAGAUGAGAAAUAAUGGUACCCAAUGAAAGACAUAGCAGUCUACAAGGAGGGGCAUUUCCCGGGGUGGGGGGGACCCACACUCUGUAACUCCCACAUUCAAUUAGCAUGUUAUAGGUAAGCUGCAGAAAACGAGGCAGCUUGUCAAAGAGGAACGGCUCUUGGCCAUGGUUGCUGCCCUAGGAGGAUAUUUGAUACUAGCAGAGCUGGGGCAACCCUGGAGGAAACCACCUGGAAUGAUGGGAGAACUCCUCCAGGGAACAUGGCCCUUUAAUAGAUCUCUGUUAUAAAAAAUAAUCCCAAAGCAGCCACCAGGGCAUACUGCUGCGAUCAAGUCCUAGGCGGUAUUCCCUUCUGCGCCAUAGACCCUGUGCAGAGUGCCCUCAACGAAGGAGCAAGGAAGACCAAGUCUCCCGAGGGUUUGCAUAUGUGUAUGUGAUUCUGCAGUCAUGGUGAAUGACACAGUCAGGGCUGCGGAAAAGCAUUGGUAAAGUGUAUAUUUGAGGCUUCAGAAGUUUGAAAAGGCUAGAUUUCCUAGGCCAAAACACUGAAAAUUUGCAAUUAGAACUUCAGUGCUGAUGCUGGGAAGACUGGAGUUAGUUUGAGACAUGCACCUGUGCAGAACUGGGCCCCCAGAAAAGGAGAAGGAAGGGAAUCCAGACCAGAGUAGGGCCUGACACCACUCAGACUCGGCGUGUCUAUAAAUUAGAAUUGCGUUACAAUUACACUUUGACAUUUUAGUGGUUUUUAAAGUGCCCAGCACAAGUUAAUUUUUCAUUAAUGAAUCCUUUAUUCAUAAAAUGCUUAGAUGGAGAUUACCCUUUUGAGCAUUUUGCCAGUGCUUCUGAAAUUAAUGGGGACCUCCUGUUGGAGGACACAGUCUGUUGCAAUAGGUGACCACUGCUCUGAAUCUAUGUCACCUCUCCAGGACCACGGGCACAACCAUCACCUGAGGCAUGUUGGAGAUGCAGAUGGUCAGGCCCUCCUAGAAUCUCAGAAUCUGCAUUUUAGCAAAGUCCUGGGUAAUUCCUAUGUCCAUUGGAGUUUGAGAAGCACUGGUAAUCUCAAAUACUUUAAAAGAUUACUAGAGUAAGAUAGGCUCAGUAGGUACCUGAAGGCACCAUCCCAAAGACCAGAGUGGUAGAAGCAGGUGGACCAGCCUCUGAACACAUUUCUCCCCCACUCCCCGGCUGUGUGGAAGGUUGCCACCUUUGGGGUAGUCAUUCAACAAACACGUGUCAACUGUCCACUAUGUGUCAGGCCACCACUGGGCACUGGCUGUGGCUAGCUGGAUAGACACCAUUUCUGCCCUCCAGAAAUGUCAUGUCCACUGGCACAUGACAAGUCACUAAGUCAUUCAGAGCCAUGGGUGACAGCUCCAGGGGCCGACAAAGGAGCUGUGAUCUCACAGAUCCACAGAGAAGUGUCCCAGGGCGGGCGGGAACCAGGACUGCACAGGGAGGGGUGAAGUGACACAUAAGAAGUCAGCCCAUCAGCCUGAAAUGCUCCCCCAAAUCUUCCCAUUCAGUGUUUUCUCAGUAGCAAACUCGUGGGAAAAUUGGUUAUUUUACUUAAAAAACUCAUACUAGAAAGCUAGUUUAACUUUAAAAAUAAAUUUUAAAAACAUUUUUAUUAACAAAUCCUACCUUUCCUCCAAAGUCAAGGAGAAAAGAAUAGAAGUGAACAAUGGACCAAGUAAGCCUAAAACUCUGCUCUUUCCCCUGCUCAUUUUACAGUUCAAGUGCCAUUCAAUUUAUCCUGGCAAGAAGAGGAAGGCAUCAUCAAGACCUUAAUUUUCUAAUACAUCUGAUCUGAGAAGAAUGUGAAAGCUAUAAAAUUAAUUUUUGAUCAAUAACUACAGGCCUUUUGAGAGAGUGCCCUCCUAAUGAAUUGAGUACCUAUUUCUCCAUACACAGUGUCUAUCAUGACCUACAAACCCUUUUCCCAUGAGGUGUAACAGAGAGAGAUUACAGCCUUGGAACUGGAUGUCAGACUCUCCUGGUUUAAGACAAUAAGCCAUGACAUAGAGCCUGAAACCAACACAAUCUUCCGAGUGGUUCCAGAAACAUAUAGGGGAUAAUGUUGGCUCUGAUGCUGUACAUCCCCAACAACCAUCAACUAUUUGGAAACUAGAAUUUCAGCAUAAUUGGAGUUGGUGUUACCCUAGCAAAUGCUGUGGGAAGAGAGUCUCACUGUGUAUCUUCUCCUGUUUAAAGCCUGAAUUUGUUCAGAAUGUAAUAUCUCUGUUUAGCCACUCUACUGAAACUGAUCUAGGAAAUGUUCAAAAAAAGGUAUCCCAAGGAUCCCUUUGUAGCUACAUCUGUGGGAUUCCCCUCGCUCUGGCGUGGCCUGGCCCCUCUGCAUUUGACAAUACGGUCCUAUGCUUUUGUCUUCCUGGGCUGCGUGAACCCACCCUGCCCUGGUUCACCUCUCCUCUUGACCCAUCCUUAUCAGUGUCUUGAAAGGUCCUUCUAUUGGAGGACACAUUCUGUUGCAGCAGGUGACCACUGCCCCAAAUCUGUUUCACCUCCCCAGGGCCAUGGGCACAACCAUCCCUGGAGUGUGUUAGAGAUGCAGUUGGCCAGGUCCUCCAAAAUCUCAGAAUCUGCAUUUUUGCAAAGUCCUGGGUAACUCCUAUGUCCAUGAGAGUUUGAGAAGUACUGGUCUCAUGAGUUCCUGACAUACAAAUAGUGCUGAGGCCAGUAUGCUGACUGGGUAGCCAGAUACAAGUGAAAACCUUCCUGUUUUUUGCAAACCUGGAUGGACCCGAGGCCGCUGACGUGGGCCAGGACAAGCUACUCUUUUUCAGUGUUUCUGUUGCAUCGCUGUGUCUCUCUGUGAUCAGGUGCUGCCCUCCCUGGCAGGAGGACUGCAGACAGGAUGACCAAGAGCACUCUACACAGCCUGCUCUCCAGUGUUGGGGGACGCCACCCACCCUCGUGGUUCCUGUUCAUCUGCCUACACGUGGAGGGCCCAAGAGGGCUAAUAUGUGACUAUCUCCACUUCCUGGUACCCUGUGUGAAUAACUUCACUUACUAAAGGGAUGUUGAGCAACUUUAUUAAUAAUGAAGAAAGCACUUUGGUUUGACAAAUAAUCACUCCAUUUUUUCAUUUGAAAGUUAACUCUUGUUAGUAGAGAAAGCAAUGUAUUACAACCACAAGGACGUUUACAUGGAAAUGAACCAUCUGCAAAGCAUCCCCCAUUUUCCUUUUAAAUCAGCCAAUGGGUGGUGGUGGGAGAAAUAUUCACCAGAGUAUUUAACAUCUAUCCCCCUUCCUAGACUGUCAGCUCCAUCCGGGCGGAGACUGUUGGUAUCUCCACAGCACACACAGGGCCUGGCACACAUCCGGGGCUCAGUGAGCACUUGCUGAAUGGUGAACAGAUUAGCUCUCCUGGGAACGUUGUUGACACAUCUCAUAACACUGGUUUGGAGUGGAGGGCAUUCAUCGGGCUGCAUAUUCCUAUUUUUAAUUGUAUUCUCCACUGGUUACAGCACCUACAGUUAUAAAGACAUUGUUAACAUUGCUUAUAGGAAGACAUUUGAUGGAAAUGAGUCCAAAGGCAUUACGGUUAGAAACUGGCCAGGUGUCAUUUUUGAGAGAUUAGAUAACUGUUUUCCGGUAGAGUGAAUUGCCUGUUUGUUGCAAGUUGGGACUUUGCUGGGCUGGUUUACAGGGCCAAGGGGAAAGAGAUAAGUGGAUCUUCUAGUGAGAGGUCAUCUGUUUUGAAAGCCUGGAAGAUUCCAUGAACUAAAUCCAAGUCUUACAACACAGGGAAGUGUGUCAUACUGUGCAGGGAUGAAGUCUCCAAUUUAGCAUGAAAACAAGAGCUCCUCACACUGUCCUCUUCAGAAAGCCCAUACAAUCCAAACUUCUGAAUGCUUAGCUGCUUACAACCAUACAUAGAUUGAGGGAUAAAACUCUGAUAUGGAAGAGAAGGUAAACAUUUUUUGGCAGACAUUCCCAGGAAAAGGCGGCUCUCUUCUCUCAUUGCUGCUGCUCUUUCAGAAUCCAUUUCAACAGAGGAGGAGUCAAUGGGAGCCCCGUGCCUCUGGCAGAUAUCAUAUGGCGUUUCAGUGGCAUUGUGUGUUACCCUUCUUAGGUAACAGCUCAGCCAUUAGAAGAAUGUCCUACACACCUUCUCAUUUUCUGUGAUGAGAGGAAUGUGAGGUACUGCCCUUCGAGAGCUGUCAUUUGUCCUAGUAGCCAGCAGCGUGACUGUGCUGUCUUCUGCUCUGUCUCCCUGUCAGCCUUCUGCCCAGCCACCACCACUAUAGUUUUGUUCUCUCCAUUGGAACUCCUGGUUCAGAGAAUUACCAUAAAAAACAGACCCCUAGACAUACAACACUCUAUCACAUAAUGGUGACUUUGUCUUCUAUUUUGGAUUACUGAGCUUUCUUGGGUAACUUCCACUAAAUCGAAGUUAAUAUUAGAAGAACUUCCUCUUACUAGAAUCGAAAAGCAUUUAAGUGAUGCAGUCAAGUUUGUACCAUAAGUAAUUCAGUCAUUUAACAAAUAUAUAUGGCCUCUGUGCGACAGUGACCUUGACUGGGAAUGAAGCUGUCCCAUGUGGGGCCUGUUCUUCAAAGGCAGUUCCCUGCUGCCCAGUUCAGUCCAGUGGAUCUGGGCAUCUCUCUUUAAUCCGCAUUAGGGGCUCUUUACUGAUUCUUCACUAUCCAAAAAGACUUGGAGGGGAGACCUGAGCCCACUUCUGGAAGGAAAUGAUAACAAUUUAUUUAGAUAAUCUUUGUGCAACAAGUCAAUUCACUGAAGAGAUCUGCUCUCUAGGAGCCUCUGUGACCCCACCAUAACUGGGAAGGCUCUACCUCUCCAGUCUUCGGGCCACAUUUCUCUCUGGCCUGCUGUCUUCCCAGCACUCUCAGCCUUGCUCAUGGAGCACUCUAGUCCUCCGUCGACCUUGGCCUUUGGUAACGUGAUUUUUCACCUGGCAGCUCCCAUCUGGUCUCACUCCCUCUUUUUGUCCAGUCUGCAUGACACAGCCUCACAUCGUUAGUGUUCCCUCACUCCCCUCUUACUGCCCAACCUGCAAAGUCCAUGCCUGGGCCAGUGCAGCAUGUGUCCUCAAUGGGCUGCUGGUGGCAGUGGGGGGAACCGCACAGCCACGCUGUGUGCUGCUGAAGAAAUGCACAGCCUCCUACCCUCGCCCUCAAGAGGCAGCCAUGGCUGCGCAUUUCUGCCCUUCUGAGCUCCGCUCACUUUUGGCAGCAGCCGUUCCAACCUGCAUGGGAUCUUCACUCUCUCACAGAUGUGCUGACUCCUCCUGCUGCCUCCCCUCUCUGUGCCUUCUCACUCUCUGUUCCCUUUGCCCUUUCUCCCCUUUUCUCCUCUGCCUACCUCCAAGCCAUCCAUCACAGGACAGCUCAAGCAUCAGAUCCUCUGGGACACUUUCCUUAGUUGUUCAGUCUGAUGAGGUGUCCCUCAUCCUCUCUUAGCUGAAAAUCAGCAGCUGCCUCAACUUCUUUUCCAGCAUGUCUCAUGAGUAUUGCCACAACAGCAUCUGUCACAAUGUGGGGUAGUGGCUGACUUGCUUUUCUGCCAUUCAACUGAGUUCCCUCAGUGCUGGGGCCAGCGUGCAGUGUCUUGUAUUCAGUAUAUAGCUGAUUAAUUGAUGAAUUGAUUAAUUAAUGGUUCACACUAGCACAGUGCAACCUUCAAUGCAAAGAUCUCAUCAAAAUAAUUCACAUGGUGGGAUAUUUUAGAAGGAUGACCAGGCUAGUUUGUAGUAAGAAAAAAUCAACAAGACUAGGUCAGGAAUUCUUUUUUUGUCUACAGGCUUGCUAUAGAAGAUAUUGAAAAUCAUCUACCUAAUUACCUUUAUUUUAUCAGGUUGUGUAUUAAAUAUCACGUCUGGGGGAAGAAAAUGUGAUAUGUGAUUACAGACCUUUCCUGGUACAACAUAGUACGUUUCAGAUUAACUCAAGGUAUUGUGGUGAUAUUGCGGUCAAAGCCAGGUGAUUAAAGAGUCAUUCUUUGAAACAAAUAUCUGUGCAAUCAAUUAAGAAAUUAAUUUGCAAAUUUUAUUUGCUUAGAGUAAUUGAUAUAUCAUUCCUUUUACAAACAAAUAUAAAGAAAACUUAACUAAAAAUACUGCAUAUCUCUUUCAGAUUAUAUAUCCCAGAAAGGAUAUAUUUUUCUCCUUUCUGGUCUUCCUUUUUGGUGUAGCAUCUGUAGGAAAUGCAUUUCUUCAUAGCUAAGUGUACCUCCUUGUGAAAUAUCUUCAGAGUCUACUGGUGCACAUAAGCAAUUGCUGGCAGCAGCUUGAGGGUCUCCAUCUCACAUUUAUCAUAUGCCUUAUUGCAUGAGGCUUUGCAAGAGGAGGUCUAGAGCUACAAUAUCUCAUGGAUAUGAAUGUCAAUUCAAAUCCCAGUGGCAGUUUAUGAGGGGGAAAGCCUAGAAGAGAAGAAACCUAGAGGAAUCAAGCAGGAGGGGAGAGUAAUAAAAGACUAGAGCAGCAGGUUUUUCUUAACUCAAACUAGAAUUAAAUCUCUGUGUGUGUGUGCAUGUGAAUGUGCCCGUAUGUGCAUGCAUGCACGUGUGUAAAUGGAUGUGUGUGUGUGUGCAUGUGUGUGCAAGUAAGUGUGUAUACGUGUGUGGGCAUGUAUUGUGUACAUGUAUGUGUGUUUUAUGCAUCUGUUUGCAAGUAUGUGUGUAUGCACAUAAAAGUGUGAAUGUACAUGUGUGCUUGGUGUAUGUGUGUGUAUUAAUGUAUGCGUGUAGUUCUAGAGUCUAGUUAGAGAAAGUGCAUAAAGAAAUAGGGAAAUUAACAAGAAAGCUAUAGCUUAAAUUAUAGGAAAAACUUUUCUCCCUAUCAGUCAUGGUUUUAAAAUGUUCAGACUUGAUAUGUUUCCCAGUGCUAUUGUCAGAAAAUGUCCCUAUGACAUUCCAUACUACUUCAAUCAAAUCUAAAACCUUUGUUCCAACAUGUUUUAUUGAUAUGAGUAUAUUUCAAAUUUCUACCAGGUUUUUGGAGAGGUAUUUUGGCCAUAAAAUUGACUAAAUUAUUCAAAAUAAAAAAUGAAUAAGCCUGGGCCAAGGCUUGGAGACUUGCUUAACUCAGUUCUUAAAUUUUCAGAUUUUCAAAAUUACAAAUUUAAGCUCUAAAAUCAUGGUGCUGUGUAUGAUAUUCUUUGAUUGCAACUUAUGGUUGAAAAACUAUAGAGGGCUUUAUGCUAAGAGUUGUGGAUCUUAGGAUUUUCAUGAAAUCUGCAUUAUCAUCAUCUGCAAGUUUAGAUGGGGCAUAACUGAUCCAAAGGAUGGAUCCCUCGGGGGCAAUUCAACUGGCUGAUUCCAGCCAAGAUGACAACAGUCAGGAUCCGUUCCCUUCUGAUCAUCCAUUGGGUGCCCUGAUUUCCUCUACAGCCCUAGCUGAAAGACCAGACACUAUCUCAGGCUGGCUGCCCCACAUGCCUUGCUCCACACCAAAUUCACAGUCUAUAAACCUGAGCCUCCAGUGCUCCUACUACCAUACUCACUCGAACAUUCCCGAUUCUGACCUGGAGAUGUCAACAGCUACUUGAUGCCACUCUCUUCUAUCUUUCUGUAGCUAAGCCAUCCCCAAGUUUGUCGAUUCACCCUCUUUAACCCCUGUCGGGGUGUCCAUUGUGCCCCUUCACCCUGCCAUCUCCCUGGUGCACUGUUUUGCAAAGUUCAGCAUACAUGAGCGUCACCUGGGAACCUUAAUAAAGUGCAGAUGUUGAUUCAGCAAAUCUGGGAUGCCCUCGGGCUGCAUUUCCAGCAGGCUCCUGGGGAUGUCCCCGCUGCUGUGCUGCAGAUGACACUCUCAGUGGUGGGACUCCAGGCUCUGCUGUCGCCUCCUAGGGGUUUCUCCACACUCCCUGGAGGCCUAAUGGGCCCUUCUCCACAUGGCAGUAAGAUCUGUUUUUGUGUUUGUGUUUCAAGUUGGGAGAAGGAGAUUAUUUAAUACUAAAAUGUGCAACAUGGGAUUGAGAAAACUAAUUAUUAGUCAUAAGUUGAGUAUGCAACAUUGAAACCACAUGCUUUAAAAAAUUAUAAGAAAAAAUCAUAGUAUUUGAAAGUUACAAGCUAUUAUGGCUAACUCCAUUUAUCUCAGUUAGAGAAGAAGAGUCACCUGUCACCAGGGCACUGCCAGAAGCCAGGCUCAUUUCCAACAGCACUGGGUGCUCCAGCUUUGGGGUGCCAGCUCCUCCCAUAAAGCAAACACAUACCUAGGGAUGAUAUUUCUUUGCAAGGGCUCUGCCCUACAGCUUGUACAUCUCAAGAAGUUAUGUAAUUAAACUGUCUGUUUUGAGAAAAUUGUAGAUUCACACAUACUAGCUGUAAGAAAUGAUGCGGAUAAAUCCAGCGUACCAGCUUUCCCCACGGAGACGUCUUGCAGCGUCACAGCCAGGAUGAGGCAUUGACCCAGGCGAAGUCCAGAGCACCUGUGCGCUACAGGGCCCCUUGCACUGUGCUGUCACAGACACGCCCACUUCCAGAUGCCAUCUAGGACCCCCUCCAAAAAGCAGAGGCAUUCUUAAAAACACACAUCUGCACAUGUUCCUCUUCAUUUGAAUCUGUCAGUGGCUUCUCAGUGCCUUUCAAAUGAAAUCUAAAGUCCUUACAAGCCUUGCAGCAGGAACCUCUCCAUCCCACUUCCCCUCACACUCUCAGCUUCAUCUCUGCUAGGCUCUGUUCAGCCAGGCAGCCUUUCACAGUCCCUCUCCUCCUGCCCUGCCAGGAAGGUCCCCUGCCCCCAACUCUUCCCCACAUGUGGCGGGGCCCCGCUUGUCCUUAGAAGCCCAGCUGAACUGCUUCCUGAAGGAACCCCUCCAGAACCUCUCAGACCAGGUCAGGUUUCUGCACUCUUAGAUCAUCCCCAUGGCAUAAUCACAGUUGUGAUGUUGUGAUGAUUCAGUGAAUGUCUGUCUCCCCACUGGAUGGUAAGCUUCCUGAGGGCAGGAACAGCAUUGGUUCCAGUCAAUGCUAUGUCCCAGGACUGUUCGUUUUUGCACAUACUAAUCCUAAAAGGACGAUGACAACAGCAACCACUUACAUGACCUAGAUGCUCUUCUGGGUGUUGUGCAAAUAUUAACAAUUUAAUCCUUGCAACAAUCCACGAGGGAGGCAUUCUUCUACUCCCACUUAACAGACAAGGACAGUGAAGCUAGUAAAGAGAAGUCAUUUGCCCAAGGGGACCCCACUACUGUUGGCAGAGCUGGGUGCAAACGCAGGCUUGUGAAGCCAGGACCCAUGCAUUCAAAGACCAUGCCAGGUGCCCCCACUGCACACCUCAUCCCCACAUACCAGUGAGGGGGAGAGAAAUGCUCCUGCACUGCCUCUGAUUAACUGCUUUCCUAGAAGUCACACAUAUAAAAGGGAUUUAAUUCUAGUGGGAUUGAAUCUCAAUAGUUUCCUUAUUAGGUUGAUUUCUGUUAAUAGUUUAAGUACUGGAUAUACAUGAAUUAGAAAAUCUAGAUUAUUAGCAAAUGCAAACUAUAAAGUAUUUUAUAAAUGUUAUCUUGUUUGUCAGGGGAUGAGUGAGAUAUUCAUUAUACAAAAAGUAGUGUGGAUUUUGAGGUAGAAGGUUUACUAAGGAUCAUACCGUAGUAUGAAAUAGCCACAAACAUUCAGUGAAACCAAACACCCCCGCUUAACCUCAAACUAACACUAAAUAAUAAGGAAUAGACUUGGGGGCAGUGCAAGUGUAUUUCUAAUGGUGAAAACCAUUCCCCAGUGAAAACUAAUGUACCAUCUAGUUAAUAAGAGCUCCUCUGACCCACGCACAUCAAUACUUACAUCCCAAUGGUGAUGUGACAUUUUGGGUUUUGUAUUUCUUUUGCAAAUUGAGCUAGCAUUUUUGAUGAGUGGCAGGGCUCUGCUACCCAACCUUUGGACAGUUUCCAAGCAUAAAAUCACAAUUCCAGAUAAUUCUGUCACAAAGAUCUGGGUCUCAUUAGGAAGGAGAGGAAGCUGGGAGAUGAUCCAGUCCAACCUCCCCCAAACCAAACAUCACGGCCUUCUCAGUUGUUUCACCAACCAUCUAAAUGUUUUAGUAAUUCUAAAAAUUGAUGCGCUUUUUCCACGAAAGGAAGUGUUACCACAUUUUCCAAGUGGGAGGCAUCUAUAUCCUUACUCCUUCAUCCUCUCCUUCCCACCCCCUCACCCCCCACCACCCACACAACAUCUGCAAUUCUUAAACUAAAGCACAAAUUGUUACAAAAGUUAAUUGCACUUUCAAAGGAAUGCUUGUAUAGAAACUUUCUCGGCUUCAAGGAAAAAUAAUACGCUUUGAAUGGCUGUUCAACAGCAUAGAAAUUAGCUGAGUAGAAGGCACUCAUAUAGCCAUUAGGACCAAUCCUUUCUGCCGCCAACACCCCCCUUAUAAAGACUUGACAGUGGGCCAGAAUAAACAACUUCAGGAUGAAUUCAGUUGAGACACAAAGUACACACUUCCAGUUUUUCCCUUCUCUGGUUACUGGCCUCAAUAACCAGGCAGUCAACUUAAAAAGAAAAACAAAAGCUUGCUUCAGAUUACAGAUUGCAGACUUCUUAUAAUAUGUCCAUUUCACCAGGCCCCGCUCUCAGCCCCGGGAAAGGCCACUGGAAACCACCUCACAUGGUAGGGCCUUGCGGGAGCCAGUAAUAACCUUAUCUCCGUCAACAUGUUCUGUCAGAUUGAAUGGGGCAGCCAGAGAAGCCAGAGUUGGCACAGGAACCAAAACAAAGGCUUCCCAUCCUCCUGGAGUGAGCGGUUGAGCCUGGAUUGGUGCUUAGACCUAUAAUGGGUGCAAGCAGCGUUCAUUCAUAGUGGCUUUCUAGACCCAGGGACUUGGCCCCAGCCCUGCUGCUCCACUCCUCUUCUUGCUUCAUUACCACGAGUCUCCUAGACCACCGAACGAUGCCUGCAUUUGAAAGACACUUCUGCUGAUCAAAGCAGCUGAUGUGUCCCUUUGCGGUUCAUUUCUAAUUGUCCCCAAGGAGGAGAAAUUCAAAUAGUUUAUUACUGAGAGUUAAAGAAAUCCACUGAAAUAUUCUUUGGUCUAAAAUUACUGUCAUGGCGGAGCAGCUUCACCUUAGUCAUUGCCCUUAAAUAUGAAAGCUAUUUAAGAAAGUUUGCCCUUAAAUAUGAAAGCUAUUUUAAAAAGUUUAAUGAAAGAAGAGAAUCACAAAACAUUUUCAAAAAGCAAAAGAAAACCUAAGAGAAAAGUUGAAAGUAGGAAUUUUUUAAAGAAUAUACGACGUGUGUUCUGUGACUCACCCCUGCAAGUUAUUUGUGUGUAUUCCCUUGCAUAGUAAUUAAUAAUGAAGCAAAGCAUGGCAAUGAUAUCUUUUCUUGUCUAGUAUUCUAGAAGACUCCAUGUUUUUGGAAAAUAUCACUCUAGUUAGAUCUCAAAUAUAUUCAAUCAGAAAAUGGGUUUUCUACAAGAUUCUAUAUCUGUAGUCAAUAGCAAAUAUAAUUCUAUUAAGCUAGUAGGAUGUGAUAGGAAACUAAAACCUAGGGGAGACCAAAGCAAGGAAAAAUACUUCCUCAUCCAAACUUGAGAGCAAUUUACCGUCAGGCCUACUAUUAAUAGAUGGAAUACAGAUUCCAUUUUCAUUACUCAACUGCCAUAUUCAUUAUUACACUGUACAGAAAAGGGAAUCACAUCUGUUGAAAACUUAUAUAUGAUGUUCAUGCAUGCAUUCCAGUAAUUCAACAAUUUUUAUUUAUCUUUUUAUUGCUUGCUAAUUUUUCAAAAUAAUAAGCUAAAGAAAACAAAAUGUUUGUGCUGUUCUCAGAUGACAUGUUAUCUCUUUAAAGGACAAAAUGUGCUGUGAAAUAAUAGAAUGCUUUCAGCACUCAAGUGUGAGUGAGUGCUCAUACAUGAGAGAAAGCCGUGGGGACUACAGAAGCCAAGAAGCAGAUCUAGCUGGGGAGGCCUUUGCAGAGGAUGUAGUUGUGUGGAGAGGCCACACACGUGGAAUUCCCAGGAGGGCUGUGGAGGCGGGGAAUCUGCAGGAAAGCACUGGGGUGAGAAACGUGAUGAGAAACAAUUAUUGUCUUAAAAUAUCUGCAGGGCUGUAAGGUAGAGAAGCAAUACGUUGCAUCUGUGUUAAGUCAAACAAAAUUAUCAAGGGACUGGUUUCAGCUUAACAUAAGGAACAAUUAUGUGAUAGGGUUGUCAAUAACAAGAGUAGACUGCUUCUUCACACACUCCUAGUCACUCAGAAUGGUCCAGGAGGAGUGGACAACCAUUUGGUAGAGUAUGGGAAGGCAGGGGCCCUGGGUGGGAGUGGUGAGGGUAGGGAGUGAGUAUCCCAAUCUAGAAGUAAAUUGUGCCCAGCACGGAGCUGCAACACUGCCCUGCACACAAACACACACAAAUAACAAUCCCCAGCCCCUGCAUUUCCCUCUCCGGUUUCAGGACCUUGUAUCUUACUUCAAUUCCUUUAUUUAGCUGAUGAUGAAAUAGGAAGAGCUUAGCACUAAGAAAAUCCUUUUGGAGUUUGGCCUUGGGGGAAAAUGAAUCACUCCAACCAGGUCUGUCUUCUAGAAAGUAUAGGAUGAAAGGGCUCCUCAUCACAUACUUCCUGACCUCCUGCUAGGCCUUUCCCUAAAACAGGGGCUGGCAAAGCACAACCUGUGGGUCACGCCUAGCCUGCCACCUGUUUUUGCAAAUAAAGUUUUAUUGGAGCAUGACUAUAUGUAUUUGCUUACAGUCUGUGGCUGCGUUCACACUAUCCCAGCAGAGUUGAAUAAUUGGGACAGGGACCAUAUGAUGGGUGAAGCUGAAAACAUUUACUCUCUGGCUGUAUUCAGAGGAGGUUUACUGAGCCCUUCUCUGAGACAUGGCAAGCGCUGCUUCAGGCUCAUGCUUCACUAGAUUCAGGCCUGGGGCAGUAAAGAGCCAGCUCAGGAUAGCACUCCCGACUCACUCAUUUUUUCAGGCAGGGGAGCCAUCUAAUGUCAAGUGCCUACGUGCAGGAACUGGUCUGUUAAUUAGCAGCUCUCCUCAUGGAAGGGAUAAUAUAUUCUAGAAACAGGAGUGCGGCCCUAUUGCAAGAAUGUCCUGAGCCAAAAUUAAGAUUCUUCUAUGGCAGAAACUUGGCUGGGGCUUCUCCUGAGUUAACUUGGUAGUUGUUAGUGAUUUUUGAGUCAGUUUUUCCUUGUCAACGACCCCAGGAAUGAGUUUGGGAUUACAGGGUAGCCAGGGAAAGGGAAAGCUUCACGCCCGCCCCCGGGACAAGGUCUGUCUUCACACUGCUACAUCCCUUCACCCACUUUAAAAUGAAACUUAAAAGGAGGAUUUCAGUUGAGUAGGAAGUGAGAAGAGGGCUCAUUUUAAAACAAGCGUUAAAUGAAAACCCACACACACUCAGAGCACACAAAUCCAACCACGCUUACAAAACCAUCACAGAGGGUCAGGCGAGGCCCUUUUCUAAAUGAAAAAGAACAGGGGUGGAGACUGUUCUGAGAGCAUGCUGGGUUCCCUGAAGGGAAUUCUCAGCUGUAUGUGCCCCGCACAGGAUCCCUGCUAGACACAAGGCCAGCUGCCUUCCUUUCAAGCCGCAGACGCAUCCCUGUGUCCAGGCGGGCUGGUCAGCUGCGGUCAGCACCAGCUUCCCCGCUCCAUGGUGAGGUCAUCACAACAUGUGAGCAGGAGGGCAGGCCGGCAACCUCUGAGUGCUUAGAGAAAGGGACGGGAUUCCUCCUGUGCAACCCCUCUAGUCUCACUCAGACUCAAGUCUGACUAAGGGGCCAGGUGCUUUGACCAGGGACUCUCCCCUCUCACUUCCCUCCCAGGAGUCACAGGUACAUGAGUCCUUGUUUUACAAAUGAAGAAAACAGACCCAACAUGAUUAAGAUGUUGCCUUCAUAGGGGUGGCACCAGGAUUCCAAACCAUGGACUCCACUGAGCCCAGUGCCCACUGACAUGUGCCAGUAACAGUGCAGCUGCCUGUGGUUCUGUCGACUAAACUGCCGGCAGAGGCUGGCUUUCCACCUUCUUUUUUUUUUUUUCACUCUUCAAACACUUUAUGACAUGAACAUAAACUACUGGCUGCAUCGUUCUGCUGACAACAUGACAUGUUUCUAUAACUUGAAAAAAGCAAGCAGUGGACUGCUCAUUGGUAAAAUUGAGUCAGUAAUCUUUUAGGAAGGUUAUUUUUCUUCCUUUUACUGCUUCUCAUCUGUUCCCCGCAGUAAAGAGGACAAGAUGACGACGACUCAGGGAACACCUCCAGCCUGAAGCAGCACCAUGCGAGCUUAGACCUUAGGGUCGGCUUAGAAACCACAGGCGGGGCGGCUUGGGCCCCUCGGACACUCCCUCUCGAAGCUGCUUCUCCCCAAGCUACCCCAAAGGCACUGAGCGCCCUCUGCCCCCCAGCAAUUCAAUUCACUGGCUGUCCUGCUCCUGUCAGUACUGAGAGUUGCAUGUUUGACCCUCGGGGGAAAAGUCCAGAGGCCCUGGGGUGUCCAGCAUGCUCUGAGGUCCCUGCUGCUGACCCCUUGCGCUGUCAGCAUUCAGAGACAUUCACACAGCACAGCCUCCCAGGCUAACAGCUGUCAUGGAACAGUGGAGCAGCUAGACGUGGCCAUUCUGUGGCCCAGUGCUGCAGAGGUCAAAGGGACAAGCGCAGGGAGCAUCUUUGCUUUCAGAAAAAAAAAAAAAAAAAAGAAGCACACUGGUGCACUGACCUGCUCCUGGUGUCUUUGUGAUUGCUCUUUUCUUUCGAUUUUUGGUUGUCUUUUUUUUUUUGAAAGAGGGGCUUUUAUGCUUUUUUCCUAAUGUUCAUGGGUAAACCAAUGUAAAUGUGUGUAUGUUUAUAGAGAUGGCUUUAAAUCGCAAUUCUGCAGUAGAGAUUGAUUUUUUAAAAAACAUGGGUAAAAAUUGAAGAAAAAUUUUAAAAGAACAUUUAAACCAUCUUGGGCUAGGGGUGGAUAUGCACCACCCCACGGAAGCCAAACAAAAUCUCUCUGCAGAUAAACAUUUGCAAAAAGAAUUUCCAAUCCCAAUUUUUGAGUCAGAGAUCUUUUAUUUCCUUGCAAAUUACAUAUCUGUUUCAGGAUUUUUGACUAUAAGAAGAAUGAAUGAAGAUGUGUUUCUUACAGAUAACUAUGAACAAACCAGGAAGGAUAAUAACUUGUAUCCCCCAAUUCGAAUCCAGAGGAUGGGAAGGCAUAAAAAAAAGAAAUGGAAGAAACUUUAUUUUUAGUGGUAAAUGGUGGGACUAUGUAUUUUACGUAUGGUGAAGUCACCAAGCCCAACACUUGGCACUUGUAGGCAAGGUAGUCUUCUAAUCUGAAUGUGAAGUAUUAUGUUUUCAUUUGCUUGGUAAUGAGGAAUAUUGGUGCUUUCGUCCCAGUUCUCGAGCUGACUGACUUCUCUUUCUGACGUGUGUUCCUUUAGCACACCUCUACACUGCAUGGCUCUGAGAUGUCCUGUGACUGUUUCAUGUGUAAAGUUGCCUCCCCAAAGGACUCACAUAUUCCUUCAGGGCAGUGAGUACUUCUGAUUCAUCCUUAGCAGCUACCUUCGCGCUACUUUACUAGAUAUGUUGUAGUUGAAUUAAUGAACAAAAGAACAAGCAACUUUGGUGCCUGGUGUGCAUCUCAGAGCAGGGUGGAGUGAGCCUGGCCAAAGGGUCAUCAUGCAACCUCUGUGGCUGACUCCAUCUGGCCACGGAGCUUCUCAGCCAUGCUUGGUAUUCACAUGACUUCUAGGGCGACAGCUCAACCAGCAAAUAAACAGCUUCAUAUGGGAAAUAUUACUCAGCCUUUGUCAUCAAGGAGUGAGUCACGGGCCUGAACUGAAUAGAAGAUAGAGGAGAAAAGGUGUGUGGACUGGGUGAGACAGCGCCCAGCGAGGUGAACUCCCGGCAGCCCUGCCUGUCUUUACCUGCACAUCACCUUGCUAGGGUGCCUUCGGUUGUGAGGGCCUGUCUAGGAAGAGAAGAGUUGCACCCUGGCAGGCAGCACUGAGCUGUCUCAUGCAAAGCUGAGGAAGAAAGAGUGAGCUGCCCAGUGAGCCUGCUGGGGUGGUGGAGGCUGGGCUGGGCUGUGCAGUCUGCAGCCCCCAGCAGCCCUUGGCACCUUUCUACUGCCUGGUGCUCACCAGCUCUCCAGUAACAAAGAGGGACGUGAAGUCAGAGGGGAAGGGAGGUAGCACAGGGCAGUCUUGACUUUGAACAAAGAGCUGGCUUCCUGAAGUCAGCUGGCCGGGUUUUGAAGCCGAUUUUCCAGCAGUGAUCUUUGAUGCCAACCCCAUUUAGGAAUUCUGUAUCUCCCCCUACCUUCUACCAGAUGUCUCUGAGCUCACCUUUGGUGAUAAUCAUGCAAUCUCCGUCAUCCCCACGUCCACACUGCCCCAUUCUGUCCCACCCCGGGUUCUGUGGUGCUGUCGGCUCCCCAGCGAGCCAGGAAGGGAGAGGCCAGCUCUGCUGGGGCUCCUGCCGCCCUGGCUCUGCACUGCCCUUCUCUGGCAGGUCUGAGGCGCCACUGGAGGAGCCACACGGCCCUGAAGCAGCAAGGCAGAUGCCCUGGACACAGUGGAGGCACAGAGUGCAAGCACCGGCCUGGCCCACAGACUUUUGGAGGGGAAGUGGUAUUAUUCAGUUCAAAAGUAUGCCUGUGUGUAAAGAGAGAGCCCCUGAACAUGAGUAAGCAAAAGUCUCAGCGCAGAGAUUAGACAAGUAGAAUGCUGGCCCGAGAGGAGGCGUUUACUCACCCUCUGUCUAGGAAGGAAAGCCAGGCCCAGCACGCUCACUGCUAUCUAUCCUCUCACACAGAGGGAUUUUGAAUCGAAGCCAGCAUCCUGUCCUUUCUCCAAUGUCCCCUGCUCAGGAGUCAGGACUCAGCAAGGCCCACCCCAGCCACACACAGAUACAGUUCCAGGACUCAGAACUCAGCGAGGCCCACCCCAGCCACAUGCAGGUCCAGUUCCAGGAUUCAGGACACAGUGAGGCCCACCCGAGCCACAUCCAGGUCCAGUUCCAGGACUCAGGAUUCAGUGAGGCCCACCCCAGCCACACACAGGUCCAGUUCCAGGACUCAGGACUCAGCGAGGCCCACCCCAGCCACAUGCAGGUCCAGUUCCAGGAUUCAGGACACAGUGAGGCCCACCCCAGCCAUAUCCAGGUUCAGUUCCAGUUUGCCAAGGCACGAGUAACAAGCUCACGCAGUUGGGCACUUUUGAAGAUCAUUUUCUCAGCCUCCAGAGGAUGUUCAAUAACUGUGAGGUGGUCCUUGGGAAUUUGGAAAUUACCUAUGUGCAGAGGAAUUAUGAUCUUUCCUUCUUAAAGACCAUCCAGGAGGUGGCUGGUUAUGUCCUCAUUGCCCUCAACACAGUGGAGCGAAUUCCUUUGGAAAACCUGCAGAUCAUCAGAGGAAAUAUGUACUACGAAAAUUCCUAUGCCUUAGCAGUCUUAUCUAACUAUGAUGCAAAUAAAACCGGACUGAAGGAGCUGCCCAUGAGAAAUUUACAGGAAAUCCUGCAUGGCGCCGUGCGGUUCAGCAACAACCCUGCCCUGUGCAACGUGGAGAGCAUCCAGUGGCGGGACAUAGUCAGCAGUGACUUUCUCAGCAACAUGUCGAUGGACUUCCAGAACCACCUGGGCAGCUGCCAAAAGUGUGAUCCAAGCUGUCCCAAUGGGAGCUGCUGGGGUGCAGGAGAGGAGAACUGCCAGAAACUGACCAAAAUCAUCUGUGCCCAGCAGUGCUCCGGGCGCUGCCGUGGCAAGUCCCCCAGUGACUGCUGCCACAACCAGUGUGCUGCAGGCUGCACAGGCCCCCGGGAGAGCGACUGCCUGGUCUGCCGCAAAUUCCGAGACGAAGCCACGUGCAAGGACACCUGCCCCCCACUCAUGCUCUACAACCCCACCACGUACCAGAUGGAUGUGAACCCCGAGGGCAAAUACAGCUUUGGUGCCACCUGCGUGAAGAAGUGUCCCCGUAAUUAUGUGGUGACAGAUCACGGCUCGUGCGUCCGAGCCUGUGGGGCCGACAGCUAUGAGAUGGAGGAAGACGGCGUCCGCAAGUGUAAGAAGUGCGAAGGGCCUUGCCGCAAAGUGUGUAACGGAAUAGGUAUUGGUGAAUUUAAAGACUCACUCUCCAUAAAUGCUACGAAUAUUAAACACUUCAAAAACUGCACCUCCAUCAGUGGCGAUCUCCACAUCCUGCCGGUGGCAUUUAGGGGUGACUCCUUCACACAUACUCCUCCUCUGGAUCCACAGGAACUGGAUAUUCUGAAAACCGUAAAGGAAAUCACAGGGUUUUUGCUGAUUCAGGCUUGGCCUGAAAACAGGACGGACCUCCAUGCCUUUGAGAACCUAGAAAUCAUACGCGGCAGGACCAAGCAACAUGGUCAGUUUUCUCUUGCAGUCGUCAGCCUGAACAUAACAUCCUUGGGAUUACGCUCCCUCAAGGAGAUAAGUGAUGGAGAUGUGAUAAUUUCAGGAAACAAAAAUUUGUGCUAUGCAAAUACAAUAAACUGGAAAAAACUGUUUGGGACCUCCGGUCAGAAAACCAAAAUUAUAAGCAACAGAGGUGAAAACAGCUGCAAGGCCACAGGCCAGGUCUGCCAUGCCUUGUGCUCCCCCGAGGGCUGCUGGGGCCCGGAGCCCAGGGACUGCGUCUCUUGCCGGAAUGUCAGCCGAGGCAGGGAAUGCGUGGACAAGUGCAACCUUCUGGAGGGUGAGCCAAGGGAGUUUGUGGAGAACUCUGAGUGCAUACAGUGCCACCCAGAGUGCCUGCCUCAGGCCAUGAACAUCACCUGCACAGGACGGGGACCAGACAACUGUAUCCAGUGUGCCCACUACAUUGACGGCCCCCACUGCGUCAAGACCUGCCCGGCAGGAGUCAUGGGAGAAAACAACACCCUGGUCUGGAAGUACGCAGACGCCGGCCAUGUGUGCCACCUGUGCCAUCCAAACUGCACCUACGGAUGCACUGGGCCAGGUCUUGAAGGCUGUCCAACGAAUGGGCCUAAGAUCCCGUCCAUCGCCACUGGGAUGGUGGGGGCCCUCCUCUUGCUGCUGGUGGUGGCCCUGGGGAUCGGCCUCUUCAUGCGAAGGCGCCACAUCGUUCGGAAGCGCACGCUGCGGAGGCUGCUGCAGGAGAGGGAGCUUGUGGAGCCUCUUACACCCAGUGGAGAAGCUCCCAACCAAGCUCUCUUGAGGAUCUUGAAGGAAACUGAAUUCAAAAAGAUCAAAGUGCUGGGCUCCGGUGCGUUCGGCACGGUGUAUAAGGGACUCUGGAUCCCAGAAGGUGAGAAAGUUAAAAUUCCCGUCGCUAUCAAGGAAUUAAGAGAAGCAACAUCUCCGAAAGCCAACAAGGAAAUCCUCGAUGAAGCCUACGUGAUGGCCAGCGUGGACAACCCCCACGUGUGCCGCCUGCUGGGCAUCUGCCUCACCUCCACCGUGCAGCUCAUCACGCAGCUCAUGCCCUUCGGCUGCCUCCUGGACUAUGUCCGGGAACACAAAGACAAUAUUGGCUCCCAGUACCUGCUCAACUGGUGUGUGCAGAUCGCAAAGGGCAUGAACUACUUGGAGGACCGUCGCUUGGUGCACCGCGACCUGGCAGCCAGGAACGUACUGGUGAAAACACCGCAGCAUGUCAAGAUCACAGAUUUUGGGCUGGCCAAACUGCUGGGUGCGGAAGAGAAAGAAUACCAUGCAGAAGGAGGCAAAGUGCCUAUCAAGUGGAUGGCAUUGGAAUCAAUUUUACACAGAAUCUAUACCCACCAGAGUGAUGUCUGGAGCUACGGGGUGACUGUUUGGGAGUUGAUGACCUUUGGAUCCAAGCCAUAUGACGGAAUCCCUGCCAGCGAGAUCUCCUCCAUCCUGGAGAAAGGAGAACGCCUCCCUCAGCCACCCAUAUGUACCAUCGAUGUCUACAUGAUCAUGGUCAAGUGCUGGAUGAUAGACGCAGAUAGUCGCCCAAAGUUCCGUGAGUUGAUCAUCGAAUUCUCCAAAAUGGCCCGAGACCCCCAGCGCUACCUUGUCAUUCAGGGGGAUGAAAGAAUGCAUUUGCCAAGUCCUACAGACUCCAACUUCUACCGUGCCCUGAUGGAUGAAGAAGACAUGGACGACGUGGUGGAUGCCGACGAGUACCUCAUCCCACAGCAGGGCUUCUUCAGCAGCCCCUCCACGUCACGGACUCCCCUCCUGAGCUCUCUGAGUGCAACCAGCAACAAUUCCACCGUGGCUUGCAUUGAUAGAAAUGGGCUGCAAAGCUGUCCCAUCAAGGAAGACAGCUUCUUGCAGCGAUACAGCUCAGACCCCACAGGCGCCUUGACUGAGGACAGCAUAGACGACACCUUCCUCCCAGUGCCUGAAUACAUAAACCAGUCCGUUCCCAAAAGGCCCGCUGGCUCUGUGCAGAAUCCUGUCUAUCACAAUCAGCCUCUGAACCCCGCGCCCAGCAGAGACCCACACUACCAGGACCCCCACAGCACUGCAGUGGGCAACCCCGAGUAUCUCAACACUGUCCAGCCCACCUGUGUCAACAGCACAUUCGACAGCCCUGCCCACUGGGCCCAGAAAGGCAGCCACCAAAUUAGCCUGGACAACCCUGACUACCAGCAGGACUUCUUUCCCAAGGAAGCCAAGCCAAAUGGCAUCUUUAAGGGCUCCACAGCUGAAAAUGCAGAAUACCUAAGGGUCGCGCCACAAAGCAGUGAAUUUAUUGGAGCAUGACCACGGAGGAUAGUAUGAGCCCUAAAAAUCCAGACUCUUUCGAUACCCAGGACCAAGCCACAGCAGGUCCUCCAUCCCAACAGCCAUGCCCGCAUUAGCUCUUAGACCCACAGACUGGUUUUGCAACGUUUACACCGACUAGCCAGGAAGUACUUCCACCUCGGGCACAUUUUGGGAAGUUGCAUUCCUUUGUCUUCAAACUGUGAAGCAUUUACAGAAACGCAUCCAGCAAGAAUAUUGUCCCUUUGAGCAGAAAUUUAUCUUUCAAAGAGGUAUAUUUGAAAAAAAAAAAAAGUAUAUGUGAGGAUUUUUAUUGAUUGGGGAUCUUGGAGUUUUUCAUUGUCGCUAUUGAUUUUUACUUCAAUGGGCUCUUCCAACAAGGAAGAAGCUUGCUGGUAGCACUUGCUACCCUGAGUUCAUCCAGGCCCAACUGUGAGCAAGGAGCACAAGCCACAAGUCUUCCAGAGGAUGCUUGAUUCCAGUGGUUCUGCUUCAAGGCUUCCACUGCAAAACACUAAAGAUCCAAGAAGGCCUUCAUGGCCCCAGCAGGCCGGAUCGGUACUGUAUCAAGUCAUGGCAGGUACAGUAGGAUAAGCCACUCUGUCCCUUCCUGGGCAAAGAAGAAACGGAGGGGAUGGAAUUCUUCCUUAGACUUACUUUUGUAAAAAUGUCCCCACGGUACUUACUCCCCACUGAUGGACCAGUGGUUUCCAGUCAUGAGCGUUAGACUGACUUGUUUGUCUUCCAUUCCAUUGUUUUGAAACUCAGUAUGCUGCCCCUGUCUUGCUGUCAUGAAAUCAGCAAGAGAGGAUGACACAUCAAAUAAUAACUCGGAUUCCAGCCCACAUUGGAUUCAUCAGCAUUUGGACCAAUAGCCCACAGCUGAGAAUGUGGAAUACCUAAGGAUAGCACCGCUUUUGUUCUCGCAAAAACGUAUCUCCUAAUUUGAGGCUCAGAUGAAAUGCAUCAGGUCCUUUGGGGCAUAGAUCAGAAGACUACAAAAAUGAAGCUGCUCUGAAAUCUCCUUUAGCCAUCACCCCAACCCCCCAAAAUUAGUUUGUGUUACUUAUGGAAGAUAGUUUUCUCCUUUUACUUCACUUCAAAAGCUUUUUACUCAAAGAGUAUAUGUUCCCUCCAGGUCAGCUGCCCCCAAACCCCCUCCUUACGCUUUGUCACACAAAAAGUGUCUCUGCCUUGAGUCAUCUAUUCAAGCACUUACAGCUCUGGCCACAACAGGGCAUUUUACAGGUGCGAAUGACAGUAGCAUUAUGAGUAGUGUGGAAUUCAGGUAGUAAAUAUGAAACUAGGGUUUGAAAUUGAUAAUGCUUUCACAACAUUUGCAGAUGUUUUAGAAGGAAAAAAGUUCCUUCCUAAAAUAAUUUCUCUACAAUUGGAAGAUUGGAAGAUUCAGCUAGUUAGGAGCCCACCUUUUUUCCUAAUCUGUGUGUGCCCUGUAACCUGACUGGUUAACAGCAGUCCUUUGUAAACAGUGUUUUAAACUCUCCUAGUCAAUAUCCACCCCAUCCAAUUUAUCAAGGAAGAAAUGGUUCAGAAAAUAUUUUCAGCCUACAGUUAUGUUCAGUCACACACACAUACAAAAUGUUCCUUUUGCUUUUAAAGUAAUUUUUGACUCCCAGAUCAGUCAGAGCCCCUACAGCAUUGUUAAGAAAGUAUUUGAUUUUUGUCUCAAUGAAAAUAAAACUAUAUUCAUUUCCACUCUAUUAUGCUCUCAAAUACCCCUAAGCAUCUAUACUAGCCUGGUAUGGGUAUGAAAGAUACAAAGAUAAAUAAAACAUAGUCCCUGAUUCUAAGAAAUUCACAAUUUAGCAAAGGAAAUGGACUCAUAGAUGCUAACCUUAAAACAACGUGACAAAUGCCAGACAGGACCCAUCAGCCAGGCACUGUGAGAGCACAGAGCAGGGAGGUUGGGUCCUGCCUGAGGAGACCUGGAAGGGAGGCCUCACAGGAGGAUGACCAGGUCUCAGUCAGCGGGGAGGUGGAAAGUGCAGGUGCAUCAGGGGCACCCUGACCGAGGAAACAGCUGCCAGAGGCCUCCACUGCUAAAGUCCACAUAAGGCUGAGGUCAGUCACCCUAAACAACCUGCUCCCUCUAAGCCAGGGGAUGAGCUUGGAGCAUCCCACAAGUUCCCUAAAAGUUGCAGCCCCCAGGGGGAUUUUGAGCUAUCAUCUCUGCACAUGCUUAGUGAGAAGACUACACAACAUUUCUAAGAAUCUGAGAUUUUAUAUUGUCAGUUAACCACUUUCAUUAUUCAUUCACCUCAGGACAUGCAGAAAUAUUUCAGUCAGAACUGGGAAACAGAAGGACCUACAUUCUGCUGUCACUUAUGUGUCAAGAAGCAGAUGAUCGAUGAGGCAGGUCAGUUGUAAGUGAGUCACAUUGUAGCAUUAAAUUCUAGUAUUUUUGUAGUUUGAAACAGUAACUUAAUAAAAGAGCAAAAGCUAUUCUAGCUUUCUUCUUCAUAUUUUAAUUUUCCACCAUAAAGUUUAGUUGCUAAAUUCUAUUAAUUUUAAGAUUGUGCUUCCCAAAAUAGUUCUCACUUCAUCUGUCCAGGGAGGCACAGUUCUGUCUGGUAGAAGCCGCAAAGCCCUUAGCCUCUUCACGGAUCUGGCGACUGUGAUGGGCAGGUCAGGAGAGGAGCUGCCCAAAGUCCCAUGAUUUUCACCUAACAGCCCUGAUCAGUCAGUACUCAAAGCUUGGACUCCAUCCCUGAAGGUCUUCCUGAUUGAUAGCCUGGCCUUAAUACCCUACAGAAAGCCUGUCCAUUGGCUGUUUCUUCCUCAGUCAGUUCCUGGAAGACCUUACCCCAUGACCCCAGCUUCAGAUGUGGUCUUUGGAAACAGAGGUCGAAGGAAAGUAAGGAGCUGAGAGCUCACAUUCAUAGGUGCCGCCAGCCUUCGUGCAUCUUCUUGCAUCAUCUCUAAGGAGCUCCUCUAAUUACACCAUGCCCGUCACCCCAUGAGGGAUCAGAGAAGGGAUGAGUCUUCUAAACUCUAUAUUCGCUGUGAGUCCAGGUUGUAAGGGGGAGCACUGUGGAUGCAUCCUAUUGCACUCCAGCUGAUGACACCAAAGCUUAGGUGUUUGCUGAAAGUUCUUGAUGUUGUGACUUACCACCCCUGCCUCACAACUGCAGACAUAAGGGGACUAUGGAUUGCUUAGCAGGAAAGGCACUGGUUCUCAAGGGCGGCUGCCCUUGGGAAUCUUCUGGUCCCAACCAGAAAGACUGUGGCUUGAUUUUCUCAGGUGCAGCCCAGCCGUAGGGCCUUUUCAGAGCACCCCCUGGUUAUUGCAACAUUCAUCAAAGUUUCUAGAACCUCUGGCCUAAAGGAAGGGCCUGGUGGGAUCUACUUGGCACUCGCUGGGGGGCCACCCCCCAGUGCCACUCUCACUAGGCCUCUGAUUGCACUUGUGUAGGAUGAAGCUGGUGGGUGAUGGGAACUCAGCACCUCCCCUCAGGCAGAAAAGAAUCAUCUGUGGAGCUUCAAAAGAAGGGGCCUGGAGUCUCUGCAGACCAAUUCAACCCAAAUCUCGGGGGCUCUUUCAUGAUUCUAAUGGGCAACCAGGGUUGAAACCCUUAUUUCUAGGGUCUUCAGUUGUACAAGACUGUGGGUCUGUACCAGAGCCCCCGUCAGAGUAGAAUAAAAGGCUGGGUAGGGUAGAGAUUCCCAUGUGCAGUGGAGAGAACAAUCUGCAGUCACUGAUAAGCCUGAGACUUGGCUCAUUUCAAAAGCGUUCAAUUCAUCCUCACCAGCAGUUCAGCUGGAAAGGGGCAAAUACCCCCACCUGAGCUUUGAAAACGCCCUGGGACCCUCUGCAUUCUCUAAGUAAGUUAUAGAAACCAGUCUCUUCCCUCCUUUGUGAGUGAGCUGCUAUUCCACGUAGGCAACACCUGUUGAAAUUGCCCUCAAUGUCUACUCUGCAUUUCUUUCUUGUGAUAAGCACACACUUUUAUUGCAACAUAAUGAUCUGCUCACAUUUCCUUGCCUGGGGGCUGUAAAACCUUACAGAACAGAAAUCCUUGCCUCUUUCACCAGCCACACCUGCCAUACCAGGGGUACAGCUUUGUACUAUUGAAGACACAGACAGGAUUUUUAAAUGUAAAUCUAUUUUUGUAACUUUGUUGCGGGAUAUAGUUCUCUUUAUGUAGCACUGAACUUUGUACAAUAUAUUUUUAGAAACUCAUUUUUCUACUAAAACAAACACAGUUUACUUUAGAGAGACUGCAAUAGAAUCAAAAUUUGAAACUGAAAUCUUUGUUUAAAAGGGUUAAGUUGAGGCAAGAGGAAAGCCCUUUCUCUCUCUUAUAAAAAGGCACAACCUCAUUGGGGAGCUAAGCUAGGUCAUUGUCAUGGUGAAGAAGAGAAGCAUCGUUUUUAUAUUUAGGAAAUUUUAAAAGAUGAUGGAAAGCACAUUUAGCUUGGUCUGAGGCAGGUUCUGUUGGGGCAGUGUUAAUGGAAAGGGCUCACUGUUGUUACUACUAGAAAAAUCCAGUUGCAUGCCAUACUCUCAUCAUCUGCCAGUGUAACCCUGUACAUGUAAGAAAAGCAAUAACAUAGCACUUUGUUGGUUUAUAUAUAUAAUGUGACUUCAAUGCAAAUUUUAUUUUUAUAUUUACAAUUGAUAUGCAUUUACCAGUAUAAACUAGACAUGUCUGGAGAGCCUAAUAAUGUUCAGCACACUUUGGUUAGUUCACCAACAGUCUUACCAAGCCUGGGCCCAGCCACCCUAGAGAAGUUAUUCAGCCCUGGCUGCAGUGACAUCACCUGAGGAGCUUUUAAAAGCUUGAAGCCCAGCUACACCUCAGACCGAUUAAACGCAAAUCUCUGGGGCUGAAACCCAAGCAUUCGUAGUUUUUAAAGCUCCUGAGGUCAUUCCAAUGUGCGGCCAAAGUUGAGAACUACUGGCCUAGGGAUUAGCCACAAGGACAUGGACUUGGAGGCAAAUUCUGCAGGUGUAUGUGAUUCUCAGGCCUAGAGAGCUAAGACACAAAGACCUCCACAUCUGUCGCUGAGAGUCAAGAACCUGAACAGAGUUUCCAUGAAGGUUCUCCAAGCACUAGAAGGGAGAGUGUCUAAACAAUGGUUGAAAAGCAAAGGAAAUAUAAAACAGACACCUCUUUCCAUUUCCUAAGGUUUCUCUCUUUAUUAAGGGUGGACUAGUAAUAAAAUAUAAUAUUCUUGCUGCUUAUGCAGCUGACAUUGUUGCCCUCCCUAAAGCAACCAAGUAGCCUUUAUUUCCCACAGUGAAAGAAAACGCUGGCCUAUCAGUUACAUUACAAAAGGCAGAUUUCAAGAGGAUUGAGUAAGUAGUUGGAUGGCUUUCAUAAAAACAAGAAUUCAAGAAGAGGAUUCAUGCUUUAAGAAACAUUUGUUAUACAUUCCUCACAAAUUAUACCUGGGAUAAAAACUAUGUAGCAGGCAGUGUGUUUUCCUUCCAUGUCUCUCUGCACUACCUGCAGUGUGUCCUCUGAGGCUGCAAGUCUGUCCUAUCUGAAUUCCCAGCAGAAGCACUAAGAAGCUCCACCCUAUCACCUAGCAGAUAAAACUAUGGGGAAAACUUAAAUCUGUGCAUACAUUUCUGGAUGCAUUUACUUAUCUUUAAAAAAAAAGGAAUCCUAUGACCUGAUUUGGCCACAAAAAUAAUCUUGCUGUACAAUACAAUCUCUUGGAAAUUAAGAGAUCCUAUGGAUUUGAUGACUGGUAUUAGAGGUGACAAUGUAACCGAUUAACAACAGACAGCAAUAACUUCGUUUUAGAAACAUUCAAGCAAUAGCUUUAUAGCUUCAACAUAUGGUACGUUUUAACCUUGAAAGUUUUGCAAUGAUGAAAGCAGUAUUUGUACAAAUGAAAAGCAGAAUUCUCUUUUAUAUGGUUUAUACUGUUGAUCAGAAAUGUUGAUUGUGCAUUGAGUAUUAAAAAAUUAGAUGUAUAUUAUUCAUUGUUCUUUACUCCUGAGUACCUUAUAAUAAUAAUAAUGUAUUCUUUGUUAACAA